AUUUCUUGGUUUUGUUUAUCAGCCGAUCUGUUUGCUGGAUUUGGGCUUGGAAUGACCCACCUGUAAAGUGCUUUUCCUUCCUCCUCCCCUUGAACUCUGCAGGGGGCUUGGCUUGGAGGGGGCAAGGGAGGGAAAGAGAGAAGGGGGAAACACAAAAAACUUCUUUCUUUCUCCCUCCGUUUAUCUUCAGCCCGACAUUGUCACCUCCUCUUUGAGGGGUUAGAAGAAGCUGAGAUCUCCCGACAGAGCUGGAAAUGCAUUGCACUUUGACUAUGGAAACAGAGGCUAUUGAUGGCUAUAUAACGUCAGGUGACAAUGAGCUUUCACCCGAAAGGGAGCACUCCAAUAUGGCAAUUGACCUCACCUCAAGCACACCCAAUGGACAGCAUGCCUCACCAAGUCACAUGACAAGCAGUAAGUCUUCAUUUUAUGAUUUUUUUUUGUGUGUGUGUGUCUCUCCAGCAACAGACUUUAAUUUGUUAGGUCUGUGGGGUCCUCUCACAUUGUGGUAUAGCUACUGUUAUAGAUUUUGCUAAAGAAAGAACAACACAGAUUUAUUCCUGUUCAUUCUAGUAUUAUAAAACAUGAGCCUGCUUACUAGUCUGAACUAUCCCAAGGUGGCAUUUGGGAGCUGGUGCUUACCUGUAUCAGGUAAGAAAGGUUAGAAUUUGCUGGUUGUUGUUUUGACUUGCCAGGUUUAUGACUGGAUUUUUUGUUGUUGUUGGGUAAAAAAUGUGGAAACGUCACUUCCAAAGGACUCUUCACAGUUAAAAAAUGAAAUAAUUUUAUGUUGCCUUGGUAGAAAGCUAAACCGUCAGUGAUAAAAUUACAGUGUUACUUGCUUUUAAAAAAUGUGAAAGUUUCUUCUCCAAAGCAUUGGAAGUGAAGUGUAAUUGAAAAUUUAUAGAACUCAUUUAUAUCCAUUUCUGUAGCAAAGUUGAAAGGCUUUUGUCCAGAGAAGAACUGAUAAAAUUUGGAAAGAUGUUUUGAAUUUGUAGGAAAAGACAGUUUUGGCUACUGUUUUUGAUAAAGGGUCAUUUACUGAUGUAAUAUACAUUGUUUUUAUGUAAUAAGAUGCAACUUACAUGCUGUCAGUGACAGAAGACAAAAUACUUUAUUAAGAAUAUGGUUGCUUUUUUCUUAAUUAUAAUAUUUUAUCAGUUUAGUUAUCAAGUGCAAGUGCUUUAUUACUCUUACUCAAAAGUAAUUUGAAAUCUUGUUUUCUUUAUACUUUAGAUUUAUAUUUUAUUCUUACAUGUUAUAGAAAGGACAUUGGACUUACAUGUAAAUAUAAUUAAAUUUACAAGUUUUCUGUUUUGGCAAUAUGUGAAGGAAAGGCAUUCUCUUUCCUUCCCCCCCCCCGAAGAUUUAAUAACUAAGAAAAGUGAAUCAUGUACUUAAUUAUGAGCAUAUUUGUAAAUGUAUUCUGACUAUCCAGAGAGAGCAACUUUUUCUUUUUACUUCUAACAGCUCUCGAAACUGUAAGUUAUUAUAAAACUGCAAGCUUAGUAAUUAGUAAAUACUACUGAAAUUUAAGCAAUUUAUAUAGAAUACCAUUGAAUACAUUUUGCAAUUUAUUAACUUUAAGUAAUUUUAGCUAUUGACUUGAAAUUAUGAUUGAGUUUGAAUUUGCUUUAUUUAUUUAAAAGUUGUAAUUCUUUUAAGUAAUGAGCACUUCCUAAGAAAAUUUAAUUAUAGAAGCAGUCCUUACAAUUCCCGUAUCAUUUAGAAAGAAAAAACUAGUAAAGUUAGCAGGUGAAUGUAUACUAAAUUAUCAUACUAAUCUCAUAAUGAAUCUUUUGCAUUCAUGUUUUUUGCUAGUUGAUUUGAUAAAAAAUAUACUAUGACUACAAUUUAGGCAAUAGAAUUUUUACAUUUCAAUAUACUAGUUAUUUGGUGUAAUGUUUUUAUUUCUCAGAUAACUCACACAAUUUCCUAAAGAGUAAAAAGAGAUAAUAUGUAGUUUCUAUUAGUUAGCUAUUGGCUUUAGAAACAUUGCAUGUAUAGGGUAGGGAGUAACUGUUAAUCAGAGACUUGACUGUCAUCCCCUAGACACAACCACAGGAAAAUGCUUGUCAAGUGGUUAAUUGGCUGCUUUAUUUCUGAAUUUGAUUCUGGUUUUGCAAGUACUUGCUUCAGAAAGGCAGUUCACUCAUCUUUUUAAAUAAACAGUGCAGAGUGUAGGCAUGAUCAAUUUGAACAAAUAAGAACUGUGCUUUUGACAUUUGAGCUUUUCUCACCCAACAACAGUAAACUUAUGUUUGGUAGAGAGUUUUUUAACUUACUAGCCUGUGGCAAUUCCAUGUUAGUACAGGUUUUGGCUAAGAUGCACGUGUUUUCAGGUUCUUUUCCAAAGAGUUGCAGGUUAAAUAUUUUGGCUCUCACUUCAGAGCUGUCUCUUGCAUCCUUUAUGUAGCCUCUAUUUACAGUAUCUAGGUUACCCACUUAGGUGUUAGAUGGAGAAGAUACCCAUUUUUCCUCUCUGUUAGAUCUAGGAGAAUAUCAGCAUUUUAGAUUGCCAAAGCAAAUAGUGAUAGAGAGGAACUCUCGUCUAUUAAUUAGAACAAGAGACCUAGAAUUGGUCACUCUGAUGUUUUUCUGUGACUUGGAAUAAUUUUUUGUGUGCAUCUGGCCUGUCAAAUCACUUGUGUCUGAGAUCACCGGUUUUCCUAAAUCCCUUUACAUGCAUUGUUGACUUUGUUUAAUGAAAAGAACUUAUUUAUUUUCUGCAUUUUUUAAUAUCUUCAAAUAUACUUCCUGGAGGGUGCCUGCUUCCAAAAACAGAAUUGCAAUUUUGAUUGAAAGUGUUAAAGCUAAAAGUAAAUGUGAAAACCUUUAAGACAGUUUCUAGUAGCAGGAAGGAGAGGAUGGGAAUAUAUGUGUAAGGAGGAAAAAAGUUAUUUUUAAACAGUUAAAAAAAUAAAAUAAGUAAAUUUUUUUUUUUUUUUUAGUAAAACAGCUAACAUUCUGGCCAGAAAAGUAUCAAUAAGGCAUGAGAGCUCACUUAUUUUGGCUUUAGGAAGGUGGUCAGUACUACUGUAAGGUCCCAGCAUUUGUUUAAGCUAUUUGGUAACUCUUCUAAGAUGAAGGGUUUCUGUGCAACUUGCUGCCAGCUAUUGUAUAAAAAUAAUGACGGCAGCUAUCAUUAUUUGACAGUGCUAGAAUAGAGCACUGGUGACUUGGGAGGGAGAGAACUAAAAAUGUUAUAAUGCCUGACAGUUUUUGGUUUUAAAAUUUAGCAUCUAAGAUAAACUUAAGAAGAAGUAAGAGGUAUUAGUGAUCCUAACAUUUUAUAAUGACUACUUCCUAUGGUUUUGAAUGAAUUUUCUUAGAGAACUUUAAACUUUUUCUUCUGGAAUGAGGAUGUCUUUGUUAAGAAGAUGGACAUUGUUGCCUGAGAUCAUUAGUGUACAUAUUGAGUCUGCUGACAAUCUUCGGUGUCAGGGAUGACAGUAUAUGCCUUGAUGGCUAUUGGAAAUACACAGUGUUAAGUGAUUUUUAAAAAUAGAAUCUGGGACUUAAGAAUCUGAGACAGACAUCUCAGACAGAACAAUAUAAAAAUAAUCCAUAUUGUAUUUCGGCCCAUCAGAUGAAACUUACUUUGUGAUUCCUUCUGUUUCUUGGUUAGCUCAUUUCCAAUUCUUGCAUAGUUGUUCAGUAUUGGUUUCAGACUGUUCUAUACUGGCAGGUGACUAUUUUGAAAAUUGUUUAAAGUUCAAAAUUUUUAAAUUAAUUUUAUUUUUCUUAUCUAUUUUUUUAUAAUGUUUAUGUAUAAAUUUACUUUGCAGGUAGUUACUUAAAUGGGUAUGAAAAUACAUCAUGAUGCAAAAUUUGUUUCUAUUACUUUAAAGCUGUUAAGUGGAUCAACUGUACAGUCAAUGCUAUUUAUCAGUCUGAUGGCCAGGUGGCAUGUAUGGAAUCGGAAGAAGUAGUAAGUCUAGUUUUACAAGGCUCUGACCAAUAAUCAGGUCAGGGAAUCUAGUUUAUUCUUUUCAGAGUACUUCACAUUAAUUUUUUUCUUAGCUAGUUUCCAUUUUUAGAACCUAGCGAAGCAGAAGUAUAUUAUGAUUUCUAUUUUUCAUAUGUGGAAAUUGAGGCUUGAAGAAAUCAAUUUACCUCUUAGAGAACUUAGCAGAAAGAUGAAGUUAUCAGGAUUGGGACAUAAAAUUGUGAUAUUACCUUGUGGGUUAGUUAGAUAACUGCUAUCUCUACAAUGUCACCUUCUCAGGGUGUCUGCCGUGUCCAAUACUGGCCCAUAUUUUUGUGACAAAUAUCUCAGAAAUAGAAGAGUUAUUAUGAGGGUGGAGUGAUAUCAGAUUAUCUUUUCAGGCGGGUGUUCUAAUGCACUUUUUGAAAUAGAGCCUAUAUUAUGGGACUUACCAGCUUUCUGAGUUUUCUUCUGUAGCUUAGUUUGGCAGUCACCCUUGCUUGGAUUUCUGUAGGACACACCCUAAUAUAACACCAGAUGGGCUUGAUAGAAAAUCUUCUGUUUUAAGUCGCCAUACUUAGGUUUGUGUAUAUACCCAAUGUACUUUACAUUUAGUUCUUGUUUAUUAGGGAAUUAAAUAAAAAUAGUUCUGAUUUAAUUUCUUUACAGGUAUCAGAGAUAAAUGUCAUAACUAUGUACCAAAAGAGAAAAAAAGGGAAAAAAAAGGAAAGUAAAAGAGGUAUAGAUUUGUUGGUAAUCAACAGCAAAAGUGCUGUAACUUUUUCUUUGCACCUCAUUCCGCUCCCAACUCCCUAUCUUUUUAGUCUGCUUAGUACUGAGAAUUAAAGUCCGUUUUCAAAAAACAAAACAACGUAUGGCAGAAAGAUUAUCCUUAUCAUCUCUAUCUUUGUUCAAAAUCUGUCUUUCCCACUAGAAGUACUUUUUUAAAAAAAGGUAACACCAUUGAUUGUGUUCUAUUGAGAGUCUUCCUGUAAGCCAUAAUGAAUUUUCAUCUCUGGGUUCCGUGCUCUUCUCUCCUAACUUUUGACAUGUUGAUAUAUUUUGAAUAUUUACAUAUUUUUAUCAUAUUUGGAAAUAUCAAUAGCAGAGUUCCAGUCCUAAAAUGAGGUAGAAUAUGUUGUUUUUCUUUACUUUUUUCCCUUCUUAUCUGUUUAUGUUAAAUGUAUUUGUUGGCCUGUUGGUAUUUUCCUUUUGCGAAUUAAUUGAGACCCAAUAUACCUCUGUUUUGAUAUAGGUAAGGAAUAUUUAGGGAUGGUUUCCUUUAUUAUAAAUGUUAUAAUCACCACUAGAGCGAGAGAAGGUAGAGGGGCAUCCUUUAUUGAGUGCACUUAGUAUGCUAGAUGCUUUACUUAUUAUUUCACUUUGUCUCCACAUCAAUUCUGUGAGGUAGGCAUGUAAUUACUCUAUUUUAUAACACUUAAAACUGAGGCUCAGAAGCAGUAGACUGUGAGUGGUUAAAAAUAUGGGCUUUGCAAUUAUGCUGGCCUGGGUUAGAAUUCCUGCUUUGCUGUGUGACCUUGGCCAUGUCACUUCACAUCUCUGAGCUCCAGUUUCCUUAUCCGUAGAAUAGGGAUAAGCAAUACCUACCUCAAUGGGCUGUUGUGAGAUUUCAAUAAGGCAAUACAUGCAAAAUGCUCAGCACAACUUCUGGCACAUGCUAAGACUCAAUAAAUAAUCACUGCUGCUAUUACUCAGAGCAGUCAAGUUACUUUUUUAUGGACCUAUGACUUGUAAGAAAAAGGGUUUGUUUUCAAAUCCAAGUCUAUUUGAAAUCUGGGUCUUUUGCUCUUUUCUGUAUAUUGCACAGGUCCAGGGAAGAAAGAUAGGGAUUUCUGAUAAUUUAGGGUAAAAAUUGAAGCAGGAACCCUCCGUUAUUUAAAGCAUCUAUGAAGAUUUUGGUUAAGAAAGAAAUAGAGUUUGUCUAUAUGUCAGAAUUGGGGAGGGGGGUGGCGCUCAACAUUCCUGAGUAUAGUUUUGUGGUUUUGAUGAUAUGUAAAGCAAAUCACUGCAUAUUAUUGGUGUUCCAGAUAUACCAGUCAUUACAAAUAACAAAAGAAAAAAAUUCCCUUAAUAGAGUAACCUAUUCCUACAGAGAAUCAAUUCUUAGAGAGUCCUCAUCUAAAAUCUAACCUCAUUUGAUGCUUCUGGUAGUACCAUAAAUUCUCACUUGAUGAUACCUAAUAAAAUUGUUGGUUUAAUUGUUGAUUGUGCACUUCGGGGGUAGUAGUUUAGAUGUUCUAAAUUUGAAGUAGGCUUAAAUGCAAUUAUUAAUUAUAAGCAUUUGACAUUUUGCUGUUCAAUUCUAGUUGAUCAAUUCAAUAAAUAUUUGUGGGAUACCUCAUAUGUGCCAGGUAUUGUAAGGUGAAUCCAAAGGUGAAUAAAGAGUAUAGAGUCCUUUUCCUCCAGGAACUCAUACUCUAGUGGGACAGACAGACAUUAAAUAGGGCAUUUUACUGUAGUAAGCUUAGUGUCUUGAUUAUUACGGGGGAUGAGAGGUGGUGCUCAUUUGGAAAUAUUUUUUAGAGGGGGAGACUGCUUGAGCCGAGACUUAUUAAAUGAAUAGGAUUUAGGAGUAACUGGAAGGCCUUUUCAAUAAAUAAUAUAUCCACAAUAAGAGGUGAGAAAUAGCAUGCAAUAUUCUGGGAAAUACAAGCAGAUUGGUAUUUCUAGACUAUAAAGUUGGAGUCUAGGAAUUCGAGGCCAGGAAUGACUUUGGAGAGUUAAUCAAGGCAGGAUAAUGGAACAUCUUGUAUGAGAGGAAACUUGGCUUUUAUUUUCAUGGAAGUCAAUGGUUUUAACGAAGUAGGUGACUUCAGUCUUUUGACUGACAUGGAUCGAUUUGAUUACAAUGUGGGGAAAAAGAUUGUGGAUGGGGACCAGUCUCUAGGCAGGUGCAUAUUUAACAGGCUGUUUCAAUGAUUGAGUGAGAAGUCAUGCAAGCUAGCAGUAGUGGGAUAAAAAGGAAGGAGAAGGAUCUAGGUAAUAUUUAGCAUCUUAAAGUAGACAGUACUUGGGUAGUAGAAUUAAGGAGACAAUAGAGUCAAGGAUGGCAACCUUUAAAUUACGGGAUAGAUGGUGGUGGUAGGUUCUGUCAGUGAAGAUAGCAAAUACUGGAGCAGGUUUCCGGGAAAAGAUUUAGCUUAGUUCAAUUCUGGUUUGAAGCACCCACAGGGUACAAUUUGGGAGAGGGAUAGCAAUUAGGCACAUGGAUAUAGACUGAAGUAUGAAUUUUCCUAAUUAGUGAAAACUAAUAUUAGCCCAUGGUUUGGUUACUUUUCUGCCCAUAUUACUUUAACAGUAGUUUAAUACCAUAUUUUGAAAACAUUCAUGUCUAAGUAAUUCUCAGUAUUUGAUCAGUGGCCUUAUUUCCUCAAUUGCCCCAUUAAAUCAAAAUUCUAUAUUGAGUUUUAUGUGCACAGGCUUUAAUAAACUCUUUGCUUAAUGGAAUCCUUUAUACUGGUCUCAGAAGUUGAAUUAAUUGAUGUGAUUGACCCACUGAUUUUUAAACAAAAAGCUCUUCAACAUUUUGUGGUAUAUCUAAUAUCAUAACUUCUGUUUUUUAAAAAAAAUCAUAAGAUUAAUGUAUGCCAUAUACUCCAGUGCCUCUAUUCUAAUGAUCUGUCUUUAUUCUGUAACCUGUUUCCUUAUAAAUAAAUAUGCUAUUGAAAAUAUUACAUACUUAUUACAGGUUGUUAGCUAAACAUUGGCCAGUUCUGCCACAUUAAUAGCUAAGGAAUUUAAUACUCCUCACCAGAGCCUUUUUGAAGACUUUGAGAUAAAUAUGCAGAUACAAUAUAUAUUAUUUUAAAAUGAUUUUGUAUAGAAUUAAUAUUUUAAAAAUAUAAUAUCAUACCCCUUGGGAUGAGGUUACCUAGAUGGGACAGUAUAGCAUAGAUAACAUCUUAAUCAGCAUAAUUAUUCUGAAAUAUUUAUUACAGAAUUCCAUCUUAAAAAUGUAAGCGCUGACUACCCAAGACACCAUAGAAUUCCAAAUGAAUGUUAAUGCUAGAAACACUUCUUCUGAGAUUUCCUGUAUGUGGAGAUUCAGAACUCCUUAGAGAGAUAUUUUUCAUCUUUCGAUCAUUGAUCCAGCAAACAUUUAUUAAGCACUUACUGUGUAUGAUGCAUUGCUGGUGCUGGGGCUCAAAAAAUAGGUUUGGGGUGUUUUCUAGAGAAGGAUGGUAUCUUCAAGGGUCCAAAUGAAUUGAUAUUUUGUGUGAGAUCGUAAUACUGCUUAUUGCAUUUAGAAGUAAAUGAGUGUGAUGUGCUAACUGUGACUUACAUCCAUUAUAGAUUAAUGAGCUGCUUCUCACCUUUUACCUCCAAGAGUUUUUCAAAUGUGUGUAAAUUUGAGGAUGUACAGUGAAACAGACAAAAGGGCAACAAGCCACUUAGAUAGGUUCUCAGAGGAUAACAUUUCCCCACAAAAUUAUUUAUAAUGCAGGAUUUGGCACUCAUCCUUGCAAGUUCUGAAACUAGAUUUGUGGCACACUUAGAGUGGAUCUGUAUCUCAAGGUUGACUGACAUUAAACAGGUUUACAAAACUGAUAUUUAAAAUCAGAAUGCCAAUUUAUGUUUAGAUAUUGAUUAAAAAUAAAGCACACACACACACACAUGCAACCAACAAACAUAGGAGCUGGAUCACUCCAGUUGGCUUGACUAGAUCAUUUUGUUCUUGUGAACUGACCUAUAUGGGUAAUCAGUAAAGGUCAUUUACUGAGCAAGGAAUCUGAAUAAAGGGAGUUAGUUAUAUAAUUCAAAUGUUUAAUGGCAUUAGACUAAGAGAACCUAAUAUAUUCAGCAUCACAAUAGAGAUAGCAUUGCUAUUUGGAUAAUUAUGGUUGAAGUCCUUUGUCCAGUUCCCUCUCCUUUUAAUGGACAUGGAUUUAGAUUCCCUAGUUCAACCAAAAUACUUCUGAGAUUCAUUUUUUUUUCCCCUUGGCUUCCUAGGCUAAAUCCCCCAGAUUCAGUCUGUAACCUAUAUUAAUACAUACAAUCAGGUUACGACGAGUUCUUUCUGGCCUGAGAUCCAUUCAUUUUCUUUAGUGUGAUUUAUAUUUCUGCUUUAAUUUGUAAAAUGUUGAUUUUAUAGCCUAACUUUAUGAAGACAAUCUUAUAGUGCCCAUAAAGGAUACUUCCUUCAACUACUAUUGCCAUAAAUUCGAACUUCCAUUCACAGAAAUCUCGACAGCUGAUGUGGUCAGCAGUUUAAGAGUUCUUAAUAUCUAUUUUAGAUGAAGAUGGAAAAUAGCACUACCACCUAGGAAAGAUCCUUAAGUUAGCUGGUGAUAUAGAGGCACUUCCAGUUUAUAGGUCAGAAGGAAAAAAAACACCAAACCAGUCUCAUGAAAUUAUUGAAGUGAUCUGACCGCAUCAAAUGAGAUUUUAUAGCAAACUGUUGUAUUUCAUGUUAGUUAGUAGGAAAGCUGUCUUAAUUACUGAGUGUGAAUUAAGUAACUUUUCAAAGCAUAUAGAUUUAUUUGUGGGCCACACCUUGAUUAUAAAGAAAUUAAUCAGGUUUUCCAGAUGUGAAUCUUUGGGGAAAAUGGUCAUAUCUCUUCAUCCCUAGCAUAUGCAUUGUAUGCAUUGUAGGAGCCCUGUAAAUAUUUGUUGAAUGAAGAAAAUACUUAAGAUUAGCAUAUUACAUAUGUCUGUUUAAAUAGUAUGCUUCUGAUCUACUUGAAAAAAUUUGGAAACUUGAUUUCUUAGUUGUUGAAAUAAUCCAAAAAUCCUAAUUUACUUGUGAUUUUCUCUGUUUGGGGAUGUGUUAUUUUUAUAAUGUCUCACUCUGAAAAAGAUUUUGUAAUCUUCAAAUUGGUCCCAAAAGCUGAUCUCUAAGUUUCUAAACAGUUCUUAUGUUUUCUGAUUCUAUACAACCAUGUUCAGUGGAAUCCACAUGAAUGUUAAUGUAGAUGUUUCCAUGACACCACCAUCAUCAUCUUCAUUACUACUAUUAAUAUCUUGAUAUAGCACAUUUAAGGUUACAGAUUUAAUUCCAUAUACUUGUAAUUUUAAAGCCAGUUCUCCAUCACUUAAACUGUUUUUAGUAGCAUGUACAAGAUGGAAUGCUUCAAUUAGCUUUUCUUAUGCACUCCAGAUAUUUUGAUGAGUGUAUAAUUAAUCAGUGUGAAGUCACGUUCUAAUAAAUUAACAUUCUGGGUGUCUACACUUUUGACGUUUUUGUCAUUGCUCUCAUUAUCAUUGAAGCUGUAGUUCUCCUUACCCUUGUCUAUGUCAGCUCUACCUACUUCUUACUAAGACAUUCAACAUGCAGGACUUGAUCUUAUUUUGAAGUGCUAGGGUACUACGUUGCUGUGUUUUCAGUUGAAUUAACAGUGAGAAUUUCUGGUUGAGUUCUAAAUAGGCAUAAUUUCUUCUACAAGUAUAUAAAACAUUUUCUUUCAUGGCCAUUUUCAUAAAUAUCCUUGUUUUGUUGUUUAAAAAUACACAUUUUAACAAGUAAUAUUUACAUAUGGAAAUAUCUUAUAGGUCUUCUAAUCAGACUUAUGCCAAUAUGCUUAUUAUUCAGAUGGUCUGAAGUAGAUGACUUUAUUUUCAAUACAUCUGUUACUUUUUAGACUGAAAAGUGGCAUUUCUAUAGUUUUUAGGGCUGAGGAUGUAUAUUUAAUUCGUGAUUGUAAAAGGUCUAUUUCUAUUAGAAAUGCUUGCUCAGAUCACCCAAAUAUCAUCUAAAGCUUGAAAAUUGAGCUAUUCAAUAAUUUUUAGGUACUAAAAAUAGGUGGUACCUAAUCAUUUUUGUGUACUGCUUUAAAAUGACUUACGCCUUAAAAACACUGACUCGAAUGUAGUAUUUGGAAAUGUAAAAUGACUUCUAUUACAUUAUUACAUUUUUGAAAACUACUUGAAAGCAGCAAUAGAUUGUGUCUGGACAUAACUGAGAAUUAUAAAAAGAAAUAUGAGAUUUUUCUGUGAGUCUGCUGUUUUUAAGUUCUCGAAGCAUGAAUUUACACACUGCCAUCUGUCUGAAUUAUGACACAUUAAUGACCUAAUGAUAGUUUUAGAUUUAAUUUUUUUUUGGAAAUAAAAACAAAAAGAAACACCCCCGUACCUCAACAAAACACAAUUUAAAAUAAAUUAUUUUUUACAUAAAUAAAUCAUAGUAAUGCUGUUUGCAUAAAGUUUUGGGGAUGCAUUUGAAUAGUUUUAGUUGGUGUUACAUUUUGAGUACAAUACCUGUAACAAAUUUGAAGAGAUAUUUUUUCAGCCAGAGAAGCUAUAGUUAACUAGACAAUUGAUUUCAUACAACUCUAUGUAUAUGAUAAUACCAUUUAUGUUUUUAAAAGCAUAUAUGUGCAUGUGUAUGCGUGUGAAUGUGUGAAAACAAAUAAUAAGAACAAGAAGGAAACGUCAAAACUUGAUAUAGUUGACUUUGGGAUAUCGGAGGGUAAACAGGGUGUUUUAUAUUUUAUUCUAAAUAGUUCUACAUUCUUUAAGUCUCUUACAAAAAAUAAAUUCAUAUAUUAUUUGUGUAAUUUAAAGAAAAGACCAAUGAAUUCAGUCAACCAUCCUCUAAAAGAAAGUAUGGAGCCAGAAAACUGAUAGUAGCUCUGAUUACAUCCAUUUAACUUUGAAAUUUCAAUAAAAUUAUAGACUCAUAAAAAUGAUCAGCUGUCAUCAAUGAUAAAUACUGAAAUCAGGCAUUUUCAUGUACAAAUGAUAUCUUCAGAUUUAUUGAAUACUAUUUUACUAUAGAUUUAGUCAAAAUAUAAGGUAUUUUCUUUUUCUUUUAUUCUUUCUUUUUUCUUUUCUUUUUCUUUUUCUUUUUUUUUUUUUUUUUUUUUGAGACAGUGUCCCGCUCUGUCACCCAGGCUGGAGUGCAGUGGCGCGAUCUUGGCUCACUGCAACCCUUCACUCCCAGGUUCAAGCAAUUCUCCUGCCUCAGUCUCCCGAGUAGCUGGGAUUACAGGCGCCCAUCACCACGUCCAGCUAAUUUUUUUAUUUUUUAGUGUAGACAGGGUUUCACUAAGUUGGUCAGGCUGGUCUCAAACUCUUGACCUCGGGCUAUCCACCUGCCUCAGCCUCCCAAAGUGCUGGAUUACAGGCAUAAAGCCACUGCCCCCGGCUCUUUCUUUUCUUUUUUCUUUCUUUCUUUUUUUUUUUUUUGAAACGGAGUCUCGCUCUGUAGCCCAGGCUGGAGUGCCGUGGCGCGAUCUGGCUCACUGCAACCUCCGCCUCCUGGGUUCAAGCAAUUCUCCUGCCUCAGCCUCCUGAGUAGCUGGGAUUACAGGCAUGCCACCAUGCCCGGCUAAUUUUUUUUUGCAUUUUUAGUGGAGACGGGGUUUCACCAUGUUGGUCAGGCGCUCUCGUACUCCUGAGCUUGUGAGCCACCGUGCCCGGCAUUGUAUUCUUUUCUUUUCUUUUCAUCUCUUGUCUUGUCUUCUCUUCUCUUUUCUUUCCUUUUCCUUUCUUCUUUCUCUCUUUCUUUUCUUCCUUUCCUUUUUUCCUUUUUCUUUCCUUUUCCUUUCCUGAGAUGGGGUCUUGUUCUGUUGUUCAGGCUGGAGUACGGUGUCACGAUUAUAGCUCAGUGCAGCCUGGAACUCCUGGGCUCAAGCAAUCUUCUCAAGUAUCUGGGGCUACAGGUGCAUGCCACCAUGCCCAGCUAAUUUUUAACAAUUUUUUUUUAGAGUCAGGGUCUCACUAUCUUACUGUGUUGUCCAGGCUGGUCUUGAACUCCUGGCCUCAAGUGAUUCUCCCGCCUCAGCCUCCUGAGUAGCUGAGUUUACAGGUGUGAGCCACCACACUUGGCUAGGUUGUUUACAGUGGCAUUUCCAAAUAAUGUUAUAUACUCUGAAUUGUUUUAUGAGUAAUAUUCAUUCAUAGCAUGAAGUGUCAUACACUAAAUAAUGUACAUAUAAAUAUUAAAAUGACAUAUCAAUAUUAAGGAGACAUUGUGGCAUCUGAUGGCAAAAGAAAUCUGAGUAGAAUGAGUUAAAACAUAGAUUUUCAAUUCUAUCUUGCAUGUAACAAACAAGUUUACUUUUAAAAAAGAGCCUUAGUCUCUUUUUCAUAUUCAUCAAUUUAAAAUUCCCUCGAAUGUUGCUAAUUUUUUACAUUAAAACUAUUAAAGAGAAACUAUUUUUAGCAAGACAAUUCUGGUAUGUUGCUAAUGGAGGUAGGACCUGCGAAAAUAACUUAAGGCCUAUAAAAGAAAGAGCAGAGCUGUGAAGUAUAGAGAGCAUAGAAGAAAGCUGGCAAGAAGAAAGAAAGAAUAAAAAUAACAGAUUCAGAAGUGGAGGACAAGCCACAGACUCCACUUGAGUUAGUAGAUCCACUGGAGAGAGCAAUAGAGCAAAUGAAAAAUAGCGUCUUUUCCUCCCCUUUUUCUUUCUUCACAAAAAAAUAAAUAAAGAGAAAUCAGAAUUUAUAAGUGAAUCAAGGAAGCUGCCUGCUUAAGUGAUGAGGAAUGUGGCAAUAAGAUUAGAAUGGUUUCUGGUAGAAGCUAAAUGAAUAAGCAUUUAGAUUCGGGAGAAAGAAGCAUACUUCUUCAGAUAUUUGAAAGCCAGGGAGUAGGAGAUGGGGGUAGAUUGGUUAAAAGAACUGGGUCCUAAGGGAUUGAUUCUAGAACAAUUAGCCAAUUAAAGCAGGAUAAAAGUUAGUGGUGCCUAGUUAUUAAGUUAUAUUAGUUAUAAACCAGUGCUAUUAUCAGUGGCCAUCUUGGACUAAUCUAUUGCUUUUAUCUUUUGCAAAAAUGAUUGUGUACUAUACUGUGUGUGUAAGAGAUAUCCUAACUGGUCGUAUUCCUAAAUUAUCGUGGAUGCGGUAAACUUUGAUCUUGCCCCUCAGUUGUCUUUUUACUUUAGUUUAGUGGGAAAGGAGAUUGGAAGGGGGUUAGGGAGACUGUAAGGCUGCCAGAAAGAACUUUCUCUGCUUUUUUUCCCCCUCUUGGGAGAUGGCAAUGAAGAAGGAACUUGAUAUUGAGCAGAUGAGAUGAGGUUUUGCAUCCAGUUUUUGUCCUCUGAUCGCUGGUUUUUCCAUUUUCCUCUCGAAGUGUCUAAGACACAGGCACUGAGGGUUCCAGAAGACUUUCUUGAGAUCAUACUCUGUUAUUUAGAAGGCUCAGGUUGGCUUUUACCCAUUGAGACAUUUUUAAAAAAUUAAUCUGCUUUAAUACUGUAGUAAAAAUUUAUCAGUUGUGAGAUAAACUUUACAUGUGUAUCAUUGUUGAAGAAAAGGUUUACUAAGCCCAUAAAUAACAAUAAUAAAAAGAUCAGGGUAUAUGUUUAACUUGCUUAAAAAAACAAAUUUUAAGUCUACUAAGAAUACCAUUUUAUUUGUAAGGUACUUUUUUCAAAAUGCUUUUACAUCUAGCAUAGAAUGUGCUGAUCAAAACUUGAGCUUAAUAUUUAUGCAACCAGUGUCAGAGUAAUCUACUCUUUUUGAUAGUACUUAGCAUUACUGGAAAAUAGUGAAUAUUUAUUUUAUUUAUUUAUUUAUUUAUUUAUUUAUUUUUUCGAGACGGAGUCUAUCUUUGUCGCCCAGGCUAGAGUGCGGUGGUGCGAUCUCGGCUCCACUGCAACCUUCGCCUCCCGAGAAGCUGAGAUUACAGGUACCUGCCACCAUGCCUAGCAAAUUUUUGUAUUUUUAGUAGAGACUGGGUUUUACCAUGUUGGUCAGGCUAGUCUUGAACUUCUGACCUCAAGUAAUCUGCCUACCUCAGCCUCCCAAAGUGCUGGGAUCACAGGCGUGAGCCACCGUGCCUGGCCAGUAAACAUGUUUUUAAAAAUUACAGAAUUGAGCAAGUUUUCCUGUUUCUCUCCCUCUGUGGUAUAUAAAGAAGUGGGACCUAAUAUAUGUCAAAUGUGAGGCCCCUAGACAGAUAUUUUAUCUCUUGGAAGCUCAGCUUUAUUUGUAAAAAGGGGAUAUUGCUCUCUGUCAGAGGAGUGGUAAGCAUUAGACACAAUAUAUGUAAAGCUUCCAGAACAGUGACUGGCUCAUGGUAAGUUAGCCAGAAUGAUAGCUCCUAUUUUAUUGUUAGAUAAAAAGAAUAUGAGAAAAAAGUUGAAUUACAUAAUAACUAAGAAACAGGUCCCACAAACAUAUAUCAAAUAGUCUUCUAGGAAGGACAUGCUUUUAGUCCGCUUUUAAUCAACAAUAAUUUUAAAAAUUAGUCCAAAGCAUUGCAUGGAACAUAACAUAUCUGGAUCACUUACUGAAUAUUUCUGCUUUUCAUCUGUUUGAGUGCUGUCAGGUAGACAGACUCAGAAUUUUUGUUUGAAAAGAAAUGUGUAUGCAGAUAUGAGACAAUUAUUAAUUCUGUUGUAUUCAAAUCAAUUACUGAAGAAAUGAAAGUAAAAUUACCUAAUUAAAUUGAAUCACACAUAAACCUACUCUGUUUGUGACGGGUAUAAUUGAAAUGGUAAUUAAGUGGUAGUAAUGCAUUUCAUUUGAGGAUGGCAAUUCAGAAGAUGUGUUUGCUGGCAGGUCUUGGCUGCUUGGUGUACCUCCCUAGGUGACCUUGUCCAGAGUGAGUUUUUAGGAUGGACUUAUUUACUUGUAUAACUAGAUGUGUUGGUGAAUGAAUUCCUAGUAUAGCUCUGAAAUUUUAUUAAUUUCCAUACUUAUGGUGCUCUAUGUGUUAUAUUAAAUUCAUGUCUCUGUUGCAUAUCUGGAAUUCUCAGAACCACAUAUACAUACCCCAGCAGUGUUCUUUUUUUCUCUCUUGUGUAGAAUCAAGGAGAAAACAGAAUAUUCAGUUUAAAAGGAUUUCACAUUAGAGUACACAUAAACAGACAUUUUCCUGAGUGAAGUUUCACCUUUUUUGGGUCAGAGUUACUAUUGUCAUAGGCACAGGACAGUCGAUCCCUAAUUCCAAAUGAUCUUUUUUUUUUUUUUGGAUGCCUUUAUCACCUCCUAUCCUGUUUUAUCAUUGCUUAAUUUCUUGAGUACAUCUUAUCUCCUUUGUGUGACUGGAAACUCCUUGAGGGCAGGGAAAAUGACUUUGUAAUCUCUGCAGCCUGAGGGUAGCAGACAGAAUAUGACUUUUAGCACCUAACCGACUGGGAUAGUAUCUUUCCUAUGCUGUGUUUUAGUUACCUCAUUUGUAAAAUAGGGAAAGUUAGUGCUUGUCUCUUGGAGUUGUUGUGAGGGUUAAUAAACUUAGUAAAGCUUUUAUCACAGGGCCUAAUACAUUUUAAGAAAUAAUUUAAGAAAUAUUCAUUUAUCUUUUCCACAGAAGCUAACACAGUGCCUUAUACAUAGUAGUCUCUCAAUUAAGAAGAUUUGCUGUUUAUUUUAAAAUAUAUUGUGAGUUAAUAUCCCUAUGUGUUGGUUAUCUGAUUGACUGAAUGCAUUAGAGACGUCUCUCAGUUAUUCCAGACAUUAUUAUUCAGAUUAACCCCACAGGUUACUUCAGUUAUGCUAUCUGUGUUGAGGAUACCAGAGACCAAAUCACCCAGCUAGUCUUACCCAGAAGGCAGUUUUAAAAUAAAUGCUCUAACGAUGGCUCUAGCUUAGACAACUUUUAACUCUUUUCUCAACACUCAUUCAAACAAUACUACAUUGGACUAAAAGCUUCUCAAGUACAUGACUUCAAAAGCUUCACAUGGCUUCAAAAUAUACAUCUUUUCAGCCAGUGUCACUCUAGAAUUUAGAGAUGGAUUUUAUAAAACACUUUAAGGGAUACCUAGAGAAUCUUGAAAUGUAUAUACAAACAGGUCAGAGGUAUUAUUGGAAAAUCUUAAAGAUACAAUUUAAAAGUUAGUGUUACUAUUAUUAUUUUGAGUAAUGAAUAUUUCUGAUCUUUAUGAUCCAAAUCUUUCAAGUCAUAAAUCAGUCAUUUAGUAGAUAUACAUGAAAAUGACAUGUAAUUCUAAUGUUGUUUUUAAUAAACUUUAAUCCAGUAGCUAAAUCUCAAAGAUCAUUUAGAAUCCUAUGAAUCAAAUGGCUCUCCCUUAAAACUGUUAAGACAGUUCUGUUGAUUCCAGAUUGUGAGCCAGACCUCCAUUUUCUUAGAGGAGUUGUGAUAAUUAUCACAUUUGUCUACAAUUAUUGUAACAGUACUUGGGUUCAUAUACACAAUCUUUACAAAAGAUAUUUCCCCCAGUUUUAUCCCAACAUUUACAUUCCCCCUCAGUUGAAUUCUUACUAGAAAUAUUUGCUUAAAUAUGUCCAAGCAAUUUGUUACAUGAGCAAUCAUUAUCUAGUUUUACAAGCAUUUGUUUGUAAUCAUUCCUAUAGCUGCAAGAAAUAAGGCAGUAUAUUUAAUAGCUUGAAGAAUACCAUGUAUUCUCUUUGUUUACAUUGUAACAGAUCAUCUUCUUAAGAAGUAAUCUUUUAUUGUAUCUCUUUCACUGUUUUCUUUAACGUUACAAAAAAAUUUUGUGUUAUUUGGAAGCUCAUGAAAUAUAAUUUGCUUGGCGUAUGGUUCUGUGAAUUAAGCCCAUAAUAUCUAACUGGCAUAUAUAGGAAAGCAAUGUACUUAAUCCUAACUGAACUGAAAAUUCAAGCUUGUAUCCAUAUAUUUUUAGUAGCAAUUUAAUGAUAAUCAAGUCAUAUGCAUUUAUGUGCCAAAAAGAACUGUUUGUGGUAAUCAAUCUGUAAUUUUCUGUUUGACAUUUUUUUCCUUUGAAUUACUGUAAAAUACUUUCAGCUACUAGUAAGAUUAUUUUAAAUCACAAUUAAAAUUGAUUUUUCCCUGCUUGGGUGGGUCUUAAGGUUGGUGGGGAACUUCAGUGCUCCCCCAAAUGCUUCCUUUUCAAGUGUGAAGUUUACGGAUAUUUUGGAUCUUACUGUGUUCUCAGGAUCAUGUCUCUAGGUAGGCACAGCUUUGAUGACUGAUGUCUAUUAAUUGUGUUUGUCAGUUUAUAACAAAGCAUUUAUUGCUCUAAAAUGCUCUCAUGCUUUGGUAUUUUGACUUCUUUCCUGCCUGUGAGAGACCCUAGCUUAGUGAUUAGUUUUUGUUUCUGAGUUUCUGUUUUUACCAAGUGUUUUUAUUUUCUAGAUUACUGGCUAUUGGGAUAAAGGAAAUGAUCCAGUUAGAGGACAUCAGAAAACUAGAAGCUUUUGAUAGAACAACAAGAUCUAGUGUCCCUAUCUAAAGAGAAGAAAUAGAGAAGGUGUGCCUUCAUUAGAAGUGUUACAAUCAAUAGCUGCCAAUUACUUAGUGAGCAGAAAACAUCUGGUACUCACCUUCAUCUAUUUGCAGCCUGUAUAUCUUUAUGUACAGGUCCUCUUCUCUCUUUCUCAGUUUAUUUCUUUAGAUACUGUAGAUGCUUUCAUGACUUUCAACUCUGCAUCUAGCACUGUUUCUUUCCUCAAAGGAAAUCCCACAUCCAGUCUAUCAGAAAUCCUUGGCUCUGCUUCUAAAAUACAUCCUGAAUUUAAACAAUUCUCACCAGGCCCGCUACUGUAACUUUAGUCUAUCAUCAUUUCCUAGUACCUUAAGCCUAAAAUAUUGCAACAGUUUAACCGGUCUUCCUGCUUCCAUUCUUGCUUCUCUGUAGUUUGUUUUCCACACAAUAGACAGAGCCUGACUUUCUAAAACCCAAAUCAGAUCAUAACAAUUCAUUGCUUUAAACACAAAAGCUUUCCACUGAAACUAGAAUACAACUAAAAUUCCUUUCCAAAGUCUGUAAGGUCCUAAAGGCUGUGGCCCUGCCUCCAUCUCUGACUUCCUCUUCUCUAUUCUUUCCCUGUUCACUGAACUUUUAAUACCUCUUCCCUUUUUCUUUUCCGGGACAUGGCAAGUUCGUUCCUGUCUAAGGACCUCUGUACUUGCUGUUUCUUUGGUUUGGGACACGUUUUCUUCCUUGUUUUGCAUGAAAGCCUCCUUCUUUUCUUAUUUCCAUUUAACUGUCGCCUCCUUGGCGAGGCUUUGCCUGAGCAUCCUAGAUAAAUAAGCCCCUCUCCAGGCAUUCUAUGACAUUAUCCUGUUUUAUUUUCUUUAUUAUACUUAAUAGUAUCUGAAUUUACUUAAUUUGUGUAUUUAUCUCUUCUCCCAACACACAGUUGAGGAACAUUUGGCUUGUUCAUUCAUGUAGUAGGGCCAGGAAUGUAAUAGACAAUAAAUGUGAACUCACAGAUGAACUGACUCCUUGUUCUUUCCCUUCCAUAAAUAGAAUUCUCUGUGUGUGUCUAUAAAGCAAACAAAGUGUUUUACACUGUAGUGUUCAUUCUAAACCCUCUAUUUUAGAAACCUGUACAUUGAGGCGAAAGUCACAUGGGGAGAGAGUAGUACAACAACGAUUAAAAAACCUUAUCUUGGCCAGAUGUGGUGGCUCACGCCUGUAAUCCCAGCACUUUGGGAGGCCGAGACGGGUGGAUCACCUGAGGUCAGAAGUUCGAGACCAGCCUGGCCAAAAUGGUGAAACUCCGUCUCUACUAAAAAUACAAAAAAAAAAAAAAAAAAAGAAAAAAAAAUUAGUGUGGUGUGGUGGCCUGCACCUGUAAUCCCAGCUACUCUGGAGGCUGAGGCAGGAGAAUAGUUUGAACUUGGCGGGUGGAGGUUGCAGUGAGCUGAGAUCAUGCCACUGUACUCCAUCCUGGGCGACAGAAAGUGAGACUCUGUCUGAAAAACAACAACAACAACAACAAAACCUUAUCUUCUGACUCUUGGCUUGGUGUUCCUUGCUUUACAUGAUACACUCUUAUGUUUUGGGGUGAGGCCCUGUAGAAGUAGUUAAGAGUACUGAUUUUCAUAUUACAUAGACCUGGUUUGGAGUCCUGGCUGUGCACCCUACUUUUGGGUUAAGCCGUAAGGGAUUACUGACACUCCAUUGUUUUUCAACCUAAUAGCUGUGUGACCUUAGGAAUGUUCCUUAGAUUUCCUAAAUUUAGUUCCUUCAGCUGUAAAAUGGUAUAAUAAUAAUAAUACUUGCCUUAAGUUUUGAAGAAAUAAAUGUAACAAUUGCAUAGAGCACUUAGCUCAUUUUUUGGCACGUUUGCUGUUGUGAUUUAUAGACUGCAAAUAUUUGCAUAUAGCUUUUUAAUAUUUAUUAGAUAAGGCUUCUAGGGUUUGAAAAUUAAUGAAUACCAACCCCAUUCUAAAGUUACCACUUGCAUUCUAGGAAAUACAUUUGUUUUGCCUUGUUUUAAGAUUUAGAAUACCUUUUUUAUUAAACAGACAAACAAAACAAGUUUGCAUCCUCACAUUUCACCAUUUCACAAAUCUAUUGUGGUAUUUCACAAAUCUAUUUUAUUUUAUAAUGGUAACUUUAUUUAGCUUUUUCUAUUUGCUUUUAUAUUAUACUUAAUAGUAUUUUAAUUAUUAUGGUUGAUCAUCAUGGUAAUUUAAUAGCCUCUUAGGAAGGGAAAUGCUUUAUAAAAACAAUCAAAUCUAAUUUCUUUAGUUCCUAGGAUAUUUUGGAAAUACAUGUAUUCUUAAGUUAGUUAAUUGGGUGGAAAAAUUGCAGUUAUAAUUCUUUAGAAAAGAAUGUUGACAUAUCUAACCAAAAAUUCUGAUGAUAGAUAGGACUUAAAGAGAAAAUGUAAACAAGUGUGUUAUUGAUUUCAAAUUACUUUUAUUUGGGUUGGAUUAGCUGUCUUUAUGCUAGGACUAUUUGUGUGUAAUAUAGAUCAAAUAAGGUGUUCAGAAUGGGAUGAACUAUCUGGAAGGAAGUGGUGUUAUCUAUACUACUACAGCUGGAAAAUAUGACAAUUACAAACUUAAUUGAUCAAUACCGUAUCACAUCAUUAUUCAAUGAUUAAGGACUGCUAGGUGAAACUGACAUAAUGGGGUUUUCUUUUUGGAAAAUAGUAUCUUAGUUGUAUUGGUAUUCCACUGGAUAUUUAGUAAAAGUGCUAUUUACUGAGAACAUCCUUAGGAUUUAGAAAGAGAACUAUGUAGUUUUAUAGUUACAGAGAUUCUGGUGCAGAUUUGGGAAGAGGUUUGAAAUUAGUAUGUAAAGUCAGAACAGCAUGACCUCAACUAAUGUACUGUUUGCCCUUGACCCCUUCUCCACAACCUGCCACUAAUGAAAGGUCUUUGAUAAGUGUAACUGCCUUAUACCCAUUUUAUUUACAGUUUUCAUAGCUAAUGAAUAAUAAGAAAAUUCCACCAGGACCUGAUUGUUUACCUCUCUAAUAGCAAUUUACAAAUGGUGUAUGCUGUGGCUGUUACAAACCGUGUCCUGUAAUAGCAUUUGAUGUAAGUAGCUGCUCACCAUUCCAUAUUGUGGUUGGAGCUGGAGAAAUAGAAAAUUGGUCAUUUCCCGGCAGAUAGCAGUAACUUUCAAUUCAGUCAGAAUGCUGUAUGGGCUGUGAUAGGUUUAUAAUUAUUACCCAAAGAUUGAUGGUUUUUUGGUGUGUGUAAAUUUGUGCAGCAGUAAUCCAUUAAGAAAUCAAUAAUCAUUCCAUUCUGAUGUGUAGUUCCUAUUCACUGUUAUAAAUGUGUACCGUGAGCUGAAACCAAUGUGUUUUGCUUUGUUUUUUGAAAUUGUAUUUGACAGUAUUGGAAAUGAGGAAAUUAUUAUAAUAUUUUUUCUUCAAUCAAAUUUCUUUUUCUUUGUGUUCCCUUGUACCAUAUGACGUACCUAUUGCAAGUCUGCAUUUUUCUUUGAAAAAUUUUAUUUAAAACUAUUUCAAAUGUUUCUGUCUCCUUUUUACCAUCAUUUACUUUGUUGUUUAAUAAUUACAAAUUAUUUAUAAGCUUAAAGCAUCUCAGUGUUUCUUUCUGUAAUCUGGAGGUGAUUUAUUACCAACUCUAUAUGGUCAGGAAAGUAGGAAAUUCUUCUCUUGUAAAAUACAAUUUUAACCUUAAAACGAUAAUCUCAUAAAAAACAACUCUAAUGUUUAUUUAUUACCGGUACCUCCUAGGAUGCCAUUGUGGGAAGCUAGGAUUAAGGCAGCAUUGACCCUACUCUCAAAGGAGCUUAGAUUUUAGAGAAAGAAAGGCAGAAAUCAACACACAUAACAUAAGGGUGUGAAGAAAUGGGAAAAGUGGUAGGGGAAAUGUCAACCCUGAAACCAUCCAUUACGUAAGUUCUGAACUGGAACUUUGGUGUUAUGGCAUGAUAGUGCUAGGGAUGAUGGGGUGUGGGUGAUAAACUUCAUCCCACAGGGGAUGUGGCCAGCAUUACAAAAUUCUGACAUAGUGUGGGGCUAAAGAGCAGUCUAAAUAGAGAUUCUAGGUAAAAAUGAUAUAGGAACAUAGUAUAAAGUUAAAACGGUAGAGAAAGAUAUAACAUGAAAAGUAAAAGCUCCACCACUCAAGUACCCUAGUCCUCAGUUUCCUGUGCUACCAAUUCCUUAAUUAUCUUUCCAUAAUUUUUUGGUAUAUACUAGUACAAAUCAUGUGUCUACAUAUUUUGUUUCCUUUCCUAUUAAUAGUACAAAUAGGGUUGCAUGGUACAUACUUGCCCUAUGACUCAAUUUUUCAUUUAGGAUUUUUUUUUAAUACCAACGUUGUUCUUGGGUGCAUAUAAUACCUUUAUACACUGAUGAUACAUGGUGAUUUAAUUUGCUCCUCAUUCACUGUUGGACAUUUAGGUUGUUUCUAUGUUUUUGUUAUUAUGUAGACAUUGUUUCAGUGAUAUUCUUGUUCAUUCAUUUACCUUCUUUACAUCCUUAGGAUAACUUAGCUGUGUAUUUGCUAUGUCAAGAAGUCUGUGCAAUGAAUAUUUUAGUAGAUAAAGUGUGGCCAAAUUGCUCUUUGGAAAGUAUAACAAUUUACACUACAACUAGUAAUAUGUGAGUGUCUGUUUUCUCCCCUUGACAAAAAUGCAUUUUAUCCAUUUUGGUUCAUCUGAAUGGGGGAAGAUGGUAUCUACGUAUGUUUGACAUUUCUUAAUUACGGUUUUUUAAACAUAAUUUCAAAUGUUUGUUGGUUGGAAAUUCUGUAUUUAAUUUUUGUUCCUGAAGAAUAUUUCUGCUUCAGUGUCUGGGAGAAAUUAUAAUUAAAAACUCUAUUAGGAACUAGGAGAAAGAGAGAAAAAAGAUUUUAUUCGUGAUUCAUGAUUUGAGGCAUAUUUAUUAAAGGAUAAUGGCAGGGAAUGGAUGAUUUGAUGUUAAGUAGAAAUUUUCAAAUGUUAUACACUCUAGAACAGAAGAUGUGACUUUUAUUUCUGUAUCUGCUCUAAUUUCACUAGUUAUCUUGGUAAAUCACAUAAGAAACCCUUCCAAAGUAUUUAGCAUAGCAGUUCAAUGAAGUUCAGGGGUUAAUGAAAUCUGAAUUCUUAUAUCAAGAAACCUUGUCAUCCAUAUAGCCAUUCUAUUAGGGGAAAAGAUUGUGUAUCUAAUAAGAAGUAGCAAACAAAGAAUACAGAAAGAAAAAUAAACCUUUACUUAAAAAUUAUACAAUUAAUUACAUUUAAGUUGCUAGGUGAGGUAUAAGGGAAUAGAUACCUUGUGCAGGAUGUAAGGAAUAAGGACCUGAUUUCUUUUUCUUUCCUAUUUCAAGACUGGUAGAGAACUCUGAGUUUGUCAAUUGAUUAGCAAGUUGAAUUCCUUGGAAACACAUAGGCAAAGCCUACCCUUGAGAAAAGAUGAAACCUGGUACUUUGUUGUUGUUGUAUACUUAUUCAGGAAAUAAGUUGUAUACUUAUUCAGGUUUAGACUCACCCUGUACUUUCUACACAUGGGAAACUGAAAUACUCUUGAGAGCAGAGAAAGUUCAUUGCAUGACAUAUCCACUUGUACGUGAAAAAUUAUGCAUCCAAGUGUGUCGUGUAGUUUUGUAGCUCCUGGUCUGUCCCGGGAACGGGAUGGUUUGCAGACUGUUAGAGAGUAUGCUGAAGGUUACCUAGGACCUGGGUUUGUUCUUUGACCUAAAGAUAAUCCCUAGGCAGAAGGCUUGUACCUGUAUCCCUUUCCCCCUUCUGCACAAUGGCAGUUUCAUGACAGAGCUGAUUGAUCUUCUUUGCUUUUUGCCUGUAAAAUCACAUUUAAAAAUAUCAGGCUUCCAAGUUCUUUUGUGUGGCUGUGUGUGUGUGUGUGUGUGUGUGUGUGUGUGUGUGUGUGUGUGUGCGCGCGCGCGCGAGCGCAUGUGUGCGUGCACACAAGGACAUGCACCCAUGCCAUUCAUCUCACUGAAAAUAAUCCUUGAAUCAGUUACUUAAAAGUGACCCCAAAGGUCAUUUAGAACAACUUCCUUAACAAAGCAAGAAUAUCCUUGACAGCAUGCAUGACAGGUGGUCUCUGGGAUUUUGCUUGACUGCUUCAAGUGCUAGAGGAAAGGAAGUUUACUGUUCCAUUGCUGAUCAGCUCUAAUUCUUAGAAAGUUCUUCCUUAUAUUGAGCCCUCAUCUGCCUGUCUGAAAUGUCACUGCUUUUUUUUUUCACUAAGACUCAAGCUAAAUAUCUCACAAGUUUUAGAUGCUUUGUUAUGUAUUAGUGCUUGUAGAGCAGGCUUUCAUGUAGGUUUUUAGAGUGUUUUGCAUUGGCCCUUGUAUUUAGAAUACUAUCAUCAUUUCUUCUGAGGAAUGAUGCUCUAGGUGUAGUGCUUAACAUAUAUAUUAUGUCUUUUUCCACCUUUGUACCAACAGCUGCAAGUAAAGCAUGUUAAGUAUGGUAAAUAACAAAACCAAACCAAACCAAACCCUGAAUUUAUUUUCAAUAACUUGUAUCUUAUUGUUACUUUUAAGCACUUUACUCUUUUAAUUUAUUUAUUUAUUUUAUUAUUAUACUUUAAGUUCUAGGGUACAUGUGCACAACAAGCAGGUUUGUUACAUAUGUUUACAUGUGCCAUGUUGGUGUGCUGCACCUAUUAACUUGUCAUUUACAUUAGGUAUAUCCUUUUAAGUCUUUUAUUCGACAAUUCAAAUAACUUAUGGUUAAAAUAAAAUUUUGUACAAAAACUAUGCCUAUUUUGGAAACAGAAAUCCAUUGCUUAUGUUUCCAUUUACAUAUACAAUUUUGACUUUGUGCAUAGAAUUUUGAGCAGAUACUAUAAAACCUGAUGCUUUGAGGCUUAAAAGUAGGACAUAAAGUGAAGAAGGCUAUAGGGAGAUGUUACAAAACUCACAUGAAGGAAGUAUGAUCAUCUUUCAGGAUUUUACUUUGCUUAGGUUGUGGAAAUUCAUCACGGUUUUCCAGCUGACAUUUCUUAAGAAAGAUUCCUAGGUGAAAAAGAUAAUAUGGAGUCUACUGAAAGUGGUUGUAGGCAUCCACAUUUCUUCCUCUGAGGAUAUUAGCAACACUUGAAUUAGCUUAUGACUUCUUAUUUCUCCCUUGCCUGAGUGGCAGUUUUACUGUGCCUUUAUUGGAUUUACUGUUGUAAUUGGAUAUGGAAUUGUGCCGGGAAGCAUAUAUUUCAAUAUGUGCACCUUAGCAAUCUAAAUCGUUAGGAUGGUGACUCACUCACAUUUAACAGGGAAAUUAGCUGGCUUCGUCUUUGUGUGAACAUUUGAGGAGGAGCUGACCCUAGCUGCAGAAAUAUCACGUGUUCCAGGUCACCUGUGGCAAAAUCUAGCCAUGUGAAGGAUUGGAGUUUCUUUUGAUUAUCUAGGCUAGAUUUUGUCAUCCACCUCUUUACUUUAGUUUGGAGAAUUAUUUAAGUAGGAGAAUCACUGGCUGAGAAAUGAUUGGAUAUAAAUUUAAGAGCUAUGUUAGCCCAUUUAAUUAUGUCACUGCAGAUUUGGUAAGAGUGUUUCAGCAAGGUCACGUAGUACUUUUCUGGUCUGCCAUCAUGGCAAGAGACAUUAUGAAAUUCUUAGGAAAGAAUAAUCCUUAAAACCAAUUUAUUUUUAAAAUAGUUAUGUCAUAGGGUCUUUUUCUCAAACUUGCUUGAUCGUAAGAAUCAUCUAAGAUACUUGAAAAAAAUAAACAGUCCCAGACCUCAACUCAAGUAUACUGAAUCAAACAAAGUGUUCAAGGGAGGAGGAGCCUGCGACUCUAAUUCUGAUAAUCAGGCAAGUUUAGGAAAUACUGUCAGAUAGUAUAUGUGCAGGGACUUGGGAAAGAAAAUAGUGGUUGCUCCAAGGAGCUAAGAUAUUACAGCAUUUUACCAUCAAUCACUAAAAUAGUCUCUGCUUUUCAGAAGAUGGUAGAAGAACGUGACUGAACUGCAUCUUUAGGGUUGGGUGGUAGGCAGGGAGAGUUGUAGCUCUUCUCAAGAAAAAACUAAAAAUGUAAGCAUAUAUGCAUAAUUUUAUUAUUGUGGUUUGCCCUCUCUCUCUGUCUCUCUGUCUGUCUUUUCUUUUCCUCUACCUGCCUUUGAUAAUUUUUCCUUUGCUUGGCUUUCUAGGUCUUUUUGAUUGAGAUGUUUUAUAAAAUCAUGUGAAUAUUUUCACACUGUAUUUUAUUACACUCUCUAUUAUUUAUUUCUGCACUUCUCUCUCAGUUGUAUUCCUUCAGCCUGUUGACACAAAAUAGACACAUGUUCCUGUUUCAGCCAGGGAGUUUGUGCAUCUGUUGACACUUCAGAAAUAAUCAGUUUAGAUUUCAACAGCUGAUUAGUGUGCUGUUCUAACCAAACUGAGAAGGAACUCUUCAGAAUGGAAACAGAUAUUAUUCUAUUUAGUUUUUUGUACAAAUAUGUAAUAAUGGCCAUUUUAAACCAAUGCUGUGGUUAUAAAAGGCCUUUGCUGAAGUUUUGUUUUUCUUUAUUGUACCUCAAAGAGGCUAUCAAAAUGUUUAGUGACCAGUAUUCCACAAGUUGUAAUAUGCCAGGGGUAAUCACAAACAUUUCAUAAUGGUCCUUGUAUUUAUAGCAACUCAAUGAAUGUUAGAAAGAAUAUUGGUAGAAUUCCAGGAAUAUCAUACAUGAUCUGCUAACAGUUUCAGAACUCCAGCUUCCACAUUGAAUUACUACUGAAUGUAAGAAAUAUAGCUAAUGGUAUCAGUGUAGCACCCAAGUACUGAUUUGCCUAAGAUAGGAAGCCAUAUCUCCAUGAGCUGGAGCCAAAAGGAAAGAAGAGCUCAACAUUUUAAAUGCGCUUGUACAAAUACUUACCUGGUUGACCUUAUAUUUCUCCAACAGUCUGAAGAAAUAGAUCAGAAAUAGGAUCAGGGAGCAUAAUAGAAUCAGUAGAAAUAUUAUAUAAUAGAAACGGAAUCAGAAAGCAUAAAACUAGUUUCUAGAAAAGAUCCUAUAGGAUAACUAUUAUGCAUCUUGAUCAGUCAGCAAGUAUCUAUUUAGUACUUUAUGAAAAAUAUUGUGUAUAGGACAGAGAAGAAGAAUGCAUUUUUUCCUUUAAAGAGAAUCAGAUUUCACAGUUACAUCAUACAUAAAUAAAAAAAUUAAAUAGCAGUUUAAUAUUUUAGAUGGGAGUUUGAGACAUUAGGCAAACAUAGUAAAAUUAUUUUCAUAUAAUUAAAGUACAGCAGCUUGGGCAACAUGGCAAAACCCUGUCUCUACAAAAAAUACAAAAAAUUAGCUGGGCGUUGUGGCACGUACCCGUAGUCCCAGCUACUUGAGGGGCUGAGGUGAGAGGAUCCCUUGAACCCAGGAGGUUGAGGCUGCAGUGAGCCAAGAUCUUGCAACUGCACUCCAGCCUGGGUUACUACGAGACUGUCUCAAAAAUAAAUAAAUAUAUAAAGUGCAGGAUAAAGUGAUUUCUUAGGACUAAUUGUAGGUCAUCUGCCUUCCAGUUAGAGUUAUAGAAUUAAUCAUUGCCUUUCUGUAGUUUUGUCACCUACUUCUAUUACAAAAAUUUGUUUGCCAUUCUUUUUUCUGAAUGACUCCCCUUACCUGAGGAAUGCAGUCUAAUAAGCUCUUUAGCAUUUUAUACUACAGCCUUUACUAAACAGCCCAAUCUAUCUUUUUGUCUUCAUCUCCUGAAAUUCCUUUUCACAUAUACUGUGCUUCAGCCACAGAUACUUGCCAUGUCUUGAAUAUAACAUAUUCUUUCAAAUUGCCUUUUCUUUGCAUGAAUCCUUCUCCUUUCCUUGGAUUUCUGUACUUUUUCUCAACCAGGAAAACUCUCAAUCCUUUUCAAAGGUCCAGUGUAACUGCUUAUUUGAAUUUUUAGUUAUUCCCCAUAUUUCUAUAGCACUGAGUAUGUACAUGUAUCUAUUAUAGUAUUCACCACAUUGUAUUGCUAUUGUUUUAUGUCUUUGUCUCCCAUAUUAGAUUUUGAGCUCCUCUGGGGCAGACUAUGUCUUGUUCAUCUGUGUACUUAUAAUUUUGCCACUGUACCUGGCAGAGAAUAGGUGUACCACUUCCCAUUGUUUUAUGAACAAAUGACUAAAAGGAGAGUGAAUGAACUUUCAUGAAGUGGAUGGGAGUAGGAACUGGCCUUGAAGAAAGAGAGAUGGAGUUGGCUGCUUUACCUGGGGAAUGAAAAGAGGGAGAGACCUGGGCUCACAUAACAUGUAGUCUGCCUUCAACAGCAAAUUCUUUUCUCCAAACAAACAGAUACUAUCUCACUAAAGUCGAAUAAGUGAGACUGCUUCUUUCUUUGCCAGGUACUUACUGACUACUAACUAAUUAUUUUUCUUCUCCUUCAAGAUUGCUAGUAAAGGCCAAUUUUAAUCUGAUAUCACAUGCCCUUAUGCACACAGGAUGUGGUAGGGAUCCAUAUAUGAUGGUGACCUCUGAACCCGAGUCUGUAGAGAAAGCCUUGCAUUCAGUACCCAAGUCCAUUCAUCUUGGCUUCAGGCAUAUUCUUAUAACUCAGAGCUGACUAAGAUGGAUAUGUCUGUAGCUGUGCCUCAUCAUAGGGUAGAGUAUUAAUACACAAAAUUACUAGGGACUUCCUUAUGUGUGUCAUCUGUAACAGAAUAACAACAGAACAGUGGUACAUCCUUUCUUUUUUUUCCUCCUUCUCAUGUUUCUUGUCUCCCACACUUUCAUCUCUUGUUUAUGCUGGCUCGCAGCAUUAGAUUUUUUAUGAAACUUCCUCUGACUAAAGUUAGGGAAAUUUGUUUCAUCUCAGUCAUUUGCUCUUUGUCGAGCUGACCUAUUUCAUUAAAAAAAAUGAGGUUGUGGUAGGAUGAGUACUUAGAAUGCAGGAAGGGGGCAUGCCACCAGUGCCCUAGCAAAGGUUAUACAGAUAGGGCUGGCUUUAGAGAAUUACCUAUGAAUUGUUUUGGGGCCCCUUUUACUAUUCUUUUUUUCUUUCUUAGCACUUCCAUUUGCAAACCCACUUCCCUUGUGGUACUUGCUUGUUGCUUCACUGUCCUGCUCAGUCCUGCCUGCCUUUCAGGGUUGCGUGAUUCUGAUACGUGUCUUCACAAUCUUUCUUUAUUCAAACCAAAACCUGUCUGUGGACACUAGGAACCCUUUCCCCAGCUUUCCAUCCUGUCAUAGAACAAUUCAAGUAAAUGAAUUCAAGCUAAGGUUUUUGAGACUGACAUAGUUUAAUAGAUUACUGUUGUUUUAUAGUGGCAUAAAUGCUUUAAUAGAGAUGUCUCUAGAAAUUGGUUCCCAAGCCAUAGUAGUAAAUUUCUGAUAAUGGAGAUUUCAGGUACCAGAUUAUGCUGGAGGGUAUGGAGAAGAAGUUUGGGAGAGUGAUUAUUUUUCUUUUGUUUUCUGUCAAAUUAAUACCAUUAAAGUAACUGUCUUUGCAGCCCAAAGGUAGUACCAGACCUGAGUAGAGACUCUUUUUUCACAAGCACAAAAUAUUAGCACUGAUGACUGACUUUGUAGUUACAAAAGUGUUAGAGAAUAUUAGAAUCUGAAAGUGACUCUUUGGCCAUUCGUUGACCCUGUUCCAAAAAUUUUUCUGGGAAAAAAAGUUUUAGGUGGCAUCUGUAAAGCUAAACAAGAACUUUGAUUAAUAUUCUUUCAACUGCCUUUUCAGUUUGUUAGAGUUAGUGUUUUUUACUUUUGUUUUGUUUUAAUAUAAGGAACUUCUAGUUAUAGUUUUACAAAUAUAGAACACAUUUACAAAUGUCUUUAAAUACCACAUAACAUAUACUCGAUAGUCUUAGAACAGAGCCCUCCACCUAGCUAGUCUCUUCUGGAUAAGCAGUUCUCAGUCAUGUGUAGUGUUGAAAAGGUGUGCUCAUUUAAUUAUUUCCACAGUUGUCAAACCUCUGCCAUGGAAAAGAAUUUCAACCAUUUUGAUAAAGCCCCUAUAAAACCACAGCUUCUAAAUAUCCUUAAAAAUGGAAAGCCACAGGUAUACAAAAUAUAUUUUGCAAAAAUAUACCAAGUGUUUCUAUUGUGGUGUCCAAUUCACUUAUUCUAGAAUAGAAGGAAAGCCUGGUGUGUUGGAAGACAGAGUAAAAAGUCAUUAAUGUAACAGAGAUUGUCUUUUAAGUCCAUUUAUAAGCCGUCUCUCUUUUUUUAAUGAGAAUGCCUUUUUGUUCUGUAUCCUGAUUAUGGUAGUGGUUAUAAGAAUCUAUGCAUGUUGUAGAACUGAAUGCUAAAAGGAAAAAAAUGCUCAUGUUUUUUGUAUGACAACUUUAAAAAUAAAAUGAAGGGGUUAAAGAAUGUCCUUUUCACUUGAAACACUGCUAAAAAUGGUGGUUAAAUUCCAUUGAAAGAAACAACAAUAAAAAGGCUUAGUUAAUGUGGCAAUUGUAGUAGGGUUAAUAGUAUUAUACAAACUAACACUAUGAGGAAAUACAUUUUAAAUCACAAAUCAGAACUUGGGAAAUACACUUUCCCCUGUUCAUUGUCAAGAGUGGGAAACGGAAGUAUUGUAAUUAGCCUUCUGGUGCAAGUGGCAAUAAAUGCAGUUGCAGUGACUGCAGUGAUGGAUGUAGGGACUCAGGAUCAGAAUUUGAAGAGGGUAGACCUAGAGUAAUUGUUAGAGCCCCUGCCCUUAGCAGAGCAUGUCUUGACUGUUGUGCAGUUAGCAGCUCCUUGUGCCUAGCAUUUUUUCUGGAGUAGGUGUUCAAUAACUACUGAUUAAAUUCUGGGGCCUAGGUUCAAAUCUUGGCUCUACUUACCAGCUAUGUGAUCUUGGAUAUGUUACUUAACCUCUCCAUGCCUCAUUCCUCUCAGCCCUAAAGGGUUGAAGAACAUCUCUCUCAUAAGGCUGUUGGGAGAAUUAAAUGAUAUUAAGCUUUUAAAUCUCUUAGCAAAGUAUGGAGCAUAUAAUAAGUGUUCCAAUAAAUGUGAGAUAUGAUUAUUCAGUAACUGUGGGUUGAAUGGCAGUAUCUCGUAAGGCUUGUGUUGGAGAGGCAGUGUUGAAUGACAGUUGCUCCUUUCAGUGCUGGUCUGUUUAUUGGGGUCAGGAGUUUUUGUGAAAUUAAUUUCUUUCGCUGUUCAGCACAGAAUACUCAGAUGCCUAAUAUUUUAAUAUUUGUUUCUUCUCUUCCUUAUGUACCUCAAAUUCUGGGCUUUUUACCUACGGAAUUUUACCCUAAGUGCUGUUGAGUACAAAUUACGAGGUACAACAGUUAGAUGAAUUUUUUAUAAUAUGGGUUACUUUUUCCAAAUUGUGAUUAUUGGAUGUGAAAAUUGUGAUUUUUAUAAAUUAUAUUUUAAUGAUAUAUGUUUUUUAAUAAACAUUUUUGAUAGAAUGAAUGCAGGUUAAUUAAGGAGAAGGGGAACAUGCACAAGUAAAAGGAAGUCAGGGCUAAAGCAGUCAUAAUUGUACAUUCAGAGCCAAUUACCAUACAAAAUGAUAAUAGCAGAUUUUUGUGUGUGAGACAGGGUCUCACUCUGUCACCCAGGCUUGAGUGCAGUGAUGCGAUCAUGGCUCAGUGUCAACUUCGACCUCACAGCCUCAGGUGAUCAUCCCACCUCAGCCUUCCAAGUAGCUGGGACUACAGGCACAGGCCACCCUGCCUGUAUAAUUUUUUAAAUGUUUUUUGUACAGACAAGAUCCCACUGUGUUUCCCAGGCUGGUCUUGAACUCCUGGACUCAAGCAAUCCACCCGCCUUGGCCUCCCAAAAUGCUGGGAUUACAGAUGUGAGCCACUGUGCCCCCAGCCUGCAGAAAUUCUUAAAGAGCAUUUACUGUGUAUUAGGCAUUGUUCUAAGUGCUUUGCAUAUAAUUCACUUAGCAACUCAAAGUAUAUCUGUUUAGAUUAUUUUCUAUGACCAUGUAAACAUGGAAAUGGAUGGGAUUGUAUAAUAGAAAUUAUUUAUGACAUAAUUAAUUUUCCUUUAACAUUGUACGUCCUCAACACUGUUUCAUGUUUCUAAGCACAUACAUACAUUAUAAUUAUUAACAGCUACAGAGUAAUUCUUUCUGUGGUAAUGGACUAACUGGUAUCUCUUUUUUGUGUUCCUGUAACGAAGAAAGAGUUUAACAUUUAAGAUGGUAAUAAUAUGAUUUUUGUUUUUCUAAAAAUAGUGUUAUUAACUAGAAGGUCAAUAAAGUAUAAUCUGUUAUCCCUUUACAUUAAAAGAGGUUCAAACAGUGCUUUGCUAUAUUUAAGAGUUUAACCUUGUUUUUGCCUUGUUUUCCUUGUUUUACCCAUACACAAAAUAAGAAAGCUCUGAUGUUACACAGCUUUUUUUUUUUCUGUCAUACACCCAUACAUUGUAAUAAUGGGGUGGCUAAUUAUUUGCUAAAUGCUUUAAAGUAAAAUAAAAUCCAAGUAUUUAUUACACCAUGUGAAUAUUUUGACUUUUUUGGUUUACUGACAUUUGGUGUUUAGCAUUUCCAUUGUCUUUUGGUUUUGACGGGAAAAACUUGGUCUAAUACCAAUUAUGACUGUUCCAAGAUAGUAAAUGGAACAUACUUGUUGAGAUUCACAUGGUUUGAGUCAUGCAUUGCCUUUACCUAUCCUUUUAAUUUAUUGUUAAGGCAGGAGUUCAAAUUAUGGACUGGUUUCAGGGUGUGAACAUCAGUCUCUGAUUAUAAUUCAGGAGAUAUGUGGAUCUGAAGUUGAUGGACAGGCUGCCUGGUUAGCCAGGCAAGCUCCCAUUAUCUCAAGAACCUCUGCUGAUUAGUUUGCUAUCAUUUUGAGAGACCUCACUAUGAAAACAGACAUUUUCCCAGGGUGGCAGAGAGAUAAAGGAAAUAUUCGCUAUGUGGUUAAAUUCUUCCAUUGUUUUAUGCCUAUGGAAUUUUAUUUAAUAGUAUAGCAUAUUUAUUCAGGAGGAGACUAGUGUUGUUUACUCUCUAGUCACUGUUUUCCUUCCUCAUACCUCAAAUUAGGAUCGUUUCAUAUUUAAGACAUUGUAAGACAUGAUACUAUUUUCUUAGACCAGUGCCUGACAUUGAUUAAAACUUCAGUAAACGUAUCGAAUACUGAAUGAAUGGAAUUAGGUUUAGACCUGUGUAGGAACAUGCAGUAUGCUUUAUUAUAAUGUAUGCGAUUGUAUAUAUUUAUUAUCCAGCUUUUUCACAGCUGCCAUCAUCCAGCAUUACCUACUAUAACUGUGAUUCCGCCUUCUUUGAGCCAGAUGUAAAACUACACUGUUGUAACUUUUAAGGGUUAACGUGCAUUUGCCUUCAUUCUAGAAAUAGGUUUAUGCUUUUGUUUCUUUGAUUUUUUUUUUUUUUGAGAUGGAGUCUCACUCUGUCACCAGGCUGGAGUGCAGUGGCACCAUCUGGGCUCACUACAGUUGCCUCCCGGGUUCAAGUGAUUUUCCUGCCUCAGCCUCCUGAGUAGCUGGGACUACAGGCGCGCGCUACCAUGCCCAGCUAAUUUUUGUAUUUUUAGUAGAGAUGAGGUUUCACCAUGUUGGCCAGGAUGGUCUCGAUCUCUUGACCUCGUGAUCCGCCCAGGUUGCCCUCCCAAAGUGCUGGGAUUAUAGGAGUGAGCCACCGCACCUAGCCUGUGCUUUUGUUUCUUAAGAGGUUUUUGCAUUGAUCAAAAUCAUAUUAAAUCAGUUACUGUUCAGGUUCACAUUUUCACACUUUUUGGAAGACUUUUGGAAAAAUCUCUUACCCUGAGUUUCACAUUCAUUUUCAUACACUUUAUUUUGGGAAGGCAUUUGGUUCAUUCAGUGUCAUACAUCACAUGGCCAAUUAAAUAAUCACUAUUAAUUCCAUUUCUCAAGUCCAUCCAACAGUAAAUAAAUGGAAGAAAUAGGAAAGGAAGAAAAAACUUGGUCUUUUUAAAUAUUUGAUUUAAUUCAAAAUAACGUUUUAGAUGUUUCUGUAACAAUUUACAUUUAGGAUCUCUCAAAGUCAAACUAUCAGAAUACUUGUCAGAGUAAAAAAAAACCCGUUGCACCUUUGCCCCUAUAACACACACACAUCCACACCUUUUUAUUAUAGAGGAAGAUUUGAUUUUAGAUUACUCUGAGGAAGAAAAUUUUUUUUCAGGAAAACCUAUUAUCCUUAGCAAAUAUAAACACUGAAAAUAUAUUGAAAACUUUCAGUCAGCUAUUAUUUGAACUCAAAAUUUGGAGUUGGGUGUCAAUGUUAGAGAUUUUAGGAAGACAUUUAAGGCAGAGAACCAGGCUCAAGAGAUGUAUUAGACGUAACUGAUUAUUACAGGUAUAUUAGGAGGAGUUUGGGAUUGCAGUUGCAGUGGGAGAUAGGCAUUCUGGCCAUUGCUAGCACUUGUCAUCCUUGUGAUGAGUAUAAAAAUAGCUAUUUACCUUUAUUUCUGUCAAACUUGUGUAUCCUUGCCCCUCCUUGCUCAAUAGAUGCCAACUUUAAGAAUAUAAUCCCAGGCACAUUUAGAAACAUGCUAAAACAAAACAAACAAACACCUCUCUCCACUCCUUCCCUAAAACAAUUAGAAAAAACGUAUGUGCCAAGUAUCAAUAGGUACAGCUGAAGAAAGAGAGAUAAGGGGAAAAAAACCAAGCAACAACCAAACUUCUUACCUCCAAAGUAAAUUAACUUUGAAACAUGGUUCUUUGUUUUUUAGAGAAACAGACAUUUGCAGAGUUAGGGGAUUUCUUGAGAUUGUACCUGAAAGUAGGUAGUAUAUUUACUAGAGGUUUUAAUACCAUUUGUUUUGUACAAUGGAUAAAUCCCAGCAAGCUUAUGUAAUAGUAAAAUUAUGUGUAAGAAAAAGCUAUUCUCCAUGGGCUCUAAAGUUAACUUUGAAGAGGCCCCAAAAAAACUGAGUUAAGGAAGAGAUAAGAUCAUUCUUUCCUCCAGGCUGAUUUUAAGAUGUUUAAACUCCUAAAUACUGUAAAGAUUAGGCUACUCUCUGCAUACCAUUUCAGAAUGAGUUGGAGUUGUACCAUUAUAGAUCUCCACUAAGUCUCUUAGUGUUAUCAACUUCUUUGAUAGUCAUUGGAGCAAGGGACAUCCAUAUAAAGUAGGAAUAAAAGAGACAACUUAAUGAUUAUUUAACUUAGCUAAUAUUUACUGGUUAUCUCAAGGCCUUGAAAGAGAAGAUCCAGUUCAGAUUCACUUUAAAAAACAAUCAGAUAUUUAGAUUAUAUUGGCAUGCUCAUAAUUAUUUUUUUUAGAUGAUAGGAAGUCUGUAUAUCUAAUGAUUUCUCCACAGUUUUUGUAUUUUGGGGAUGCAAGUUUUUGCUUUUUUUAGCAACUGUAGGAUCAAGGGAAAUGUUUUGUCAAACAAAUCAAAUAUAAUAUUUCAAACAUAUAUUUAUAUGUAUUAAUUCAUUUAAUCUCAAUAAAACCCUAUGAGGUAGAUGCUAGUAUUGCCCCGCUGUUAUAGAUGAAAAACUGAGGUGCAAUUAAAAGCCAUUAAGAGGUAAAGCUGUGAUUCAAACCUUGGUUGCCUAGUUCCAGAAUCCUUCGUCUUAGCUAAUAUGAUAUUUCUAACACUGUAAAUUUUAAUUUAUUAUGGGUUGGGGAAUCGGUGUAAUGUAUAGAAACCAACACUUUAGUAAAAAUGAUAUGGAAUAGAAAACGUUAGAAUAUGGAAUAUUGAGCUGGGCCCAGUGGCUUGCACCUGUAAUUUUAGCUAUGCAGAAGGCUGAGGCAAGAGGAUCACUUGAGCCCUGGAGUUCAUGGCUAGUGAGCUGUGAUCGUGCCACUGCACAAUCUGUCACUGGGAGACAGGGUGAGACCCUGUCUUAAAAAAAAAAGAAAGAAGGAAAGAACUAUGAUUAUGUGUAGUAUUGUUUCAUUAAGCCAUUUUCAUAAACAUUAAUAUGUAUUUAGACAUACAUAGACAUAUGUAUAUAGUGAGUUGCAAUAAAAAUAUAUUUUUUAUUGUCUGUCUGGGUCAAAAAAAAGUUUGCAAGCCACUGAACUACACAAUCUCAAUACCUUGAAAAUAGUUGAUGUUCAGUAAAUCUGUACUAAGUUGAAUUAAUGUAUUGUUAAAUAAAAAAUAACCCAUAAACAGUGUUAGGAUAAAAUACUUCUGCUGAGCAUAUAAUUUCCCUAUGGAGUAGGACUGAAAAUGUUAGUCUCACAGUUCUUAACCAAUGAAACUGUAAUUAUCAAACAUAAUCUAUUAGUUUAUACCUGCUCCUCAACCUAAAGUUCUCCUCUGCAAAUCUUUCUGGUUGGUAAUUUUUUAUUGCUUUAAGGCUUGGCCUCUUGUCCUUUAACAAUAUCAAGUAAUAAUAGUCCAAAAAGAAGAGGCAGUUUCUAAAAAAAUAAAUUACAAUUUGAAUUCCCUGAAAGUAAUAAUUUGUUAUUAACAAAAGAAAUUUAUUUCAGCAGUGCAAGGAUGGAUCAAUAAUAGGAAAUCUAAUAUUUAUCAUAUUAAACUAAAGAGAACAAUCAUAUGAUUUUCUCUAUAGACAGUGAAAAAACAUAGGACAAAAAUUAACAACCAUUCUCUACACCCAGUAAACAGAAAUAAAGGGAAACUUCUUCAUAGUGAUCAAAUGUAUGUAUGUGAGUCCAAAAGCCAUUAUGAUUCAUAGGAAAACACAUACGCAUGCUCAGUAAUUUCAGAAACUAGGUAGAUUUUGUUUGUUCUCUUUACUCUUUUUUAAUAUUGUGCUGGACGAAACUGCCAAUGGAUUUAGAUAAUAAAAAAUAAGAUUAUAAAAAUUUGAUAGGUAGAGAUAAAAUAAUCACUUUUUGCAGAUGGUAUGUUUUGUAUCCAUAAACUGCAGAGAAUCAGCUGAAAGACAAAUAAUUCAUAAACAAUAAAAUAAUUUAGUAAUAGGGCAGUUUAAAUUAACAUGCCAAUAUUUAAAUGUGUAAUAUUUGUAUUAAAGAACAUGCAGAAGCGUACUUAAAAUGGGGAAGAUAUACUGUGAAGUAUUCUUUCACAGGUAGAUGCAAUAUUGCUUAUAUCUUAUACUGAACUUCAGGAUAAACUCUGAAUUGGAACAAAGAUAUAUACAUGAAAGUUAACCAUAUAAGUAAUAGAAGAAAAUGUGAAAGUCUUAUUAUGGUCUUACUAUGGGAAGCUCUUUUUAAUAAAAUUCAAUAUCUAAAAGUCAAUUUCAAAGGAUUAAUUCAUUUAAAAUAAUAAAAAUUUCUACAUGGCAAAAAAUAGCAUAAAUAAAACCAAAAGGUAAACAACAAGCUGGAGGUAAAAUUUGCAACUCAUAUGAUGACUUAAACGGUUAAUCUCUAAUACAUAACAGCUCCUAGUAAUUCCUGAAGUACAGUAAGUAUCUAAUAGAAAUUUGGUUAAAUUAUUCUAACACACAGUUCACAGAAAAAUACCAUUGGCUCCUACACAUAUAAAGUUUUUCUUAACUUCACCCAAAAUAGGAGGUAUAUAAAACUAUACUGACAUAGCAUGUCUAAUUCAUUAUAUUAGCAAAAAACUGAAAAUUUUGUGUCAUGCUGUGUUGGCAAGGCUGCAAGGAAACAGGGCCUUUUAUGUAUUGUUGAUGGGAGUAUAAAUUUAUAUAAAUGUGAAUUGGAACAAAUGCUUAUAAACUUUGACUCAGUACUCCUGUUUCUACAAAUUUAUCUUAUAAUAAUUUGUCAAAUGUUGAGUGCACAGAUUUAUUCAUUGCAGCAUUGUUUUUCAUAUCAAAAGAUGGGAAACAUUGUGCAAACAAUGCCCAUCAGUAGUGGAUUGAUUAAAUAAAUUAGGUAUAUCCAAUAAUUGAAUAUUAUGCAAGUAUAUAAAAAAUAAGAAUCAUGAAUAUGGAAAGAUUUCGAAAAUAUAUUGCUAAGAUUAAAAAAAAGGAAGGGGCAGAAGAAAAUAAGUUGGGUAAAAAAAACCCCAGAAAUGUUUACUAAUAAUUAUAUUUAAAAACUCAUAGGAUAAACAAGAAGGUAAUGAAAUAAUUAAUUGUUUGGGAGUGUAUAGAUAGAGGGAUGACAGCUGAGCAGAUGAGGGGCUGGGAUGGAACAAGACUCUUCACUAGAUAUACUUUUAUACUUUUUGAUUUUUGAACCAUUCAAAUAUCUACCUAUUUGACAACAUCAAAACAAAAGGAAAAAAACACUAAUAAUAACAACUAAACCACAGUAAAUAUUAGUUUUUUUGAGAAAAUAUUUCUAUAGGGUGAGACUGAAAGUGUCAGCCCUUCAACUGUUUGCCAGUGGAACUGUAAGAAACUGGUGUAAUCCAUUAAUUUGCUUCCCCAACACCCAAUUUAGAUGUAGAUUCCUUACACUCAGAUCAUUUGUUGAUGGUUUUAUUUAUUGUGUAUAUUUAAUAAUUUUAAUUGCAUUUUAUAUCUUUGUUUCCUACACAUUAACUCCAUCAAGCAAUUAAUAUUGAACAGUGUAAUUAAGUGGUAGUUUUAAAACACCAGUUGUACAAAAAUCAAGACCAGUGUUCAUUUUAGAAUUUACCAUUUUUAUACAAUAUGCAACUUUAGAAAUGAUAAUAUUAUUUAAAAUUUCUAUAGAUAUUUUACCUUGCUUAUGUUUUUCUUCUUGAAAUAUAGUAUUGCCAAAUUGCUGUACUGUAACAUCAUGAUAAUAAUGGUAGUGUUAGGAAUUUAUUUUCAUUAGUGGUCAUAGUACAGUUAAUAUAAAUAUAUAGCACAUAAAUAUAAAUGAGAACACUAAAUAUCUGUUUGGAAAUGGGAUUCAAGAGCUGUGUCUUAAGUUUUGGUAGGAUUCAUUUAAUAGCUGUGUGAAUUACUUAACCUUUCAGAAAGUUAAUUUCUUAAUCUGUUAAAAAAAAGUGAUACUAAUACAUGCCUUACAGGGUUGUGGUCAAGGUUGGAGUGAAUGUCUUUAUAAUACCUAGUAUAGUAUCUUCAAUGCAAGCAUCUAUUAUUCCUGUGGUUGUGUUACUUAUGAUAUGUAGCCCUAAAAUUGCAAGAUGAAUAUUAACAAGACAAUAUGCACAGUUUGCCACUACCUGUAAGAUUUGAUUUAUUUGAGUAAAAUAAAGGGGAGGUGGAUUAUAAAAUUUUCACUGCUAUAAUUUUGUGUCUGCUUGCAUGUUUUACUUGCUGAGAAUUUGGUAGGGUCAAGUGUUAAAAUCACUUCUAAAAUAAGUCUCCUCAAAGUGAUUAUUUAAUACGGAGAAUUAAUUACUAAUUUGAAAUAUUUUAAAUAGUGGUCAGUUAUUUAAAAAAUAAUAUAUUAAUUGGAUAGAAUAAAAUGGAGCUGUUAAAAACCAUGUGCUUUAAGAAUGAUUAUGGCAUAGACAUUUUUUGAAAUACAUACAUUAAAAAGAUUAUACAAGUUUAUAUAGUAGGAUCUCAAAUAUGUAAAGAAAAGCGUGCCAUAUAUAAAUAGAUGUAUAUUUCAUAGAGGAAAGAUGAGAUGAAUAUACACCAAAUGUGAAUAGUGGUCAUUUUUGAGUGUUGGGAUUCUUUGUGAUUUUUGUUUGAUUUAUACUUUUAUAGAUUUUACAUUUUUUUUUACAAUAAGCAUAUAUUACUUUUAUAUUAGCAAAAAAAGCAAUAUGUUGUAUUGCUUUUUUAUGUUUAUGUAUUCUUCGAGAUUGAAUUGUAGGAUGAGUAGAACCUAAAUAUAUGUACCUUCUUUUAAAGAAAAGCACUUUAAAGCUAUAUCAACUUUGUUAGUGGAAUUUUAUUCCAGAAGAGUAGAAGUUGGCACCUGGAAGCACUCUUGGACCGUUUUCCUAUUGAGGAGGGGUUUAUUUUGGUAAAGUAACACUACCACUGUAGCCCGAUGGCUACUGCAGUGGGAUCAGAUCUCAGGUCAUAUCAGUUCAGUAGCUCAGCUUGUAGCUCUGAUCUCUCAAACUGUGGGGCACAGUGAGAAGGGUUUUUUAGAAGCUGGCCCCUCUGUCUUUUCAUGCACACAAAUCUGCUUAUUAUGACCACAGUUCAUUGGGGAUGGCAGAAGUAGUACAUAAAGCUAAUGUAAGCAUAAUAUUUUAUAUUAUGUAAAAUAUUUACGUCAUGUAGAAGAAAUUUUUUAAAAUUUGUAAAAUUUUGUCAGAAAAACUUUUUUUCCUCAAUAAAAAUCACCUACUUUCCAAUGGAUAAUUCUACAUCUUAUAUAGUCCUUAUUUCAUUUUUUCACAGGUUAUCCUAGUUGACAUCAAAGCAUGCACCCAUUUUGAAUAUUUCGGGAAAUCUCAUUAAACACUGAAAAGGAUAAUGCCUUGUGGGUUGCUCCAUAGUAAUUUCAAUCGUUUUUUUCCCAAGUUUACAUUGACCCCAUUCUCCUAUCAACUCAGUAGGGUUUCACGGCCGUUGUUGCUUCCUUUUGCCUAAUUUAGCAUCAUGCCUGAUGGUUUACAUUUCACUUAAUCAUAGCUUUCGAGAUGUAGCAUACCUCUCUUUGUUCUAGAGAUAUGAAAACUAACCUACACAGUUAGAACACAGGUAAACUUCAGGUCUUUUGAUUUCGAAUUCAGCAUGCAUUGUGUUCUGUCGUGUUCCAGUAUUCUUGAUAGUUCUCUAAAAUGUUGUCAAGAAGGGCCUAAGAUCUUUGUGAUCUCGCCAAAGAGUUUAGAAGUAUGUAUGUGUGUUGUUUGUUUUUCCUCCUGCAAGAAUUCCUGAGAUAAAUUAUCUAAAUUUUCACUGAAAACAAGAAUUCCUGAGAUAAAUUAUCUAAAUUUUCACUGAAAACUCUAAUACAUGAAGGUAGUUACACAGUUCCAGCAAUGACUGAACUUGAACCAUGAUUUACAUACCUUCCCUAUUAAGUGCCAGUCAGGUUCUCGCUACAGAUGAGCAAAUCUGCUUUUUCCACAGUGAGAAAAACAUUUAGAGACAAUUCUACAAUUAGAAUUUUGUGAUACUAAUGGAAAGUGCGUGUAUGUACACGUACUUAAAAUGAGCUAUACAAUUUGUUGGGAGUUCAGUGAUCCCUCCUUUAAAAACUACAACUGUGAAGCUAUAAGACCUCACAGUGAUCAUCUCUUUGUUGACAUAAAUGUGAUAAACCUUGCCCAAGAAAUAUAUAAUUCUUUGUUUGUCUUGCUAAGCCUUAAAGUUCUCAUGGGCAAGGGAUGAGAAAGGGUCUUCUGAGGACUAUUAUUUUUUUUGUCUUGUGUUAACAGCCUGAGUGCUUUGUGAUGGUCUUUCACUGUGUGUCUGAGGGAACCCUAAGUGUUGUUUCUGACUCUGAGCAGGCUAAUUUGCUCAUCAUAGACAAUGGACCUGUUGACAAACAGGUACAUUCUCCUUACCGUGUCCUUCUAUAUGUGAUAUAGUUGAUUUCUAGGUUUAUGAUUUUCCCCAUUAUAAUUAAUCAGCAGCAUGAUAUAUCUGCUGUUUAUCAUAUAAUGGCUUUCUUGAUGGGUGGCAUAAGGAAUAUUUUAAAUUAAAAUUAAAAUUUUUUUGACUUUUGCUCUGAAUUGGAGAGAUACUUUUUGGUACCUUUGCUCAAGAUUACAUAUUAAUCACAUGUUAAAUAUAUGUAUUACUUAAUGUGUUCAUCAUAGUACAAAAUAUGAAGAAUAGAGUUAUGAGUGAGACUUGAGAUGUUUCACUUUUAGAUUUUUCAAGUGGCAAGAAACUUUUAGAUAUUUAGUCUCAGAAAUGGAAAACCUACUUAAAAAACAUUUUUUUUCUUCUUUUCUUUUCUUUUUUCUUUUUUUUUUUUUUAGACAGGGUUUCCCUCACUCUGUCGCCCAGGUUGGAGUGCAGUGGCACCAUGAUCAUGGCUUAUGUGGCAGCCUCGAACUCCUGGGCUCAAGAGAUCCUCUCACCUCAGCCUCUGGACUAGCUGGGGCUAGGGACAUGCGCCACCACCAUGCCUGGCUAAUAUCUCUCUAGAUCCGAGGUCUCACUAUGUCUCACAGGCUGGUCUCAAACACUUGGGCUCAAGCGAUUCUCCAGCCGCGGCCUCCCAAAGUGUUGGGAUUAUAGACGUGAACCAUUGUGCCUAGCCAUUUUUUUUUUUCGUAAGAGUAGUUAGACCAACUCUUCCUUUAAAAAACAGGCGCAAGGAUCUCUUAAACAGAAAAAUAGAUUGGUGCCGUCUUUCCAUAAUUUUCUUUUCAACCACAAAAGAGAUUUUUUUAAAAAAAGAUUGAUUUUAAAGAUAUGUAAAUACUAAUUAUUUGGAUUAUAAUUAUUGGUCAUUAUGGUAAUGCCUUUUUUAAAAAGAGAAAUAGCUAAUCAUGAAGUCUGACAAUUUAAAUAAAGACAGUUUAGGUAAAUUUAUAUCUUAAAGUGAAAAAUGGAAUCACUUAAUUUUGUUACUAUAUUUUAGGUCAUAAAAAUAUACUGAUUGAAGAAAACGUUUUCAAACAAAUUGUACAUUUAUCUUUUGCCCAAGAAAUCUAUUUUUAUCUGAGCUAGGUAAAACUUAAGUCAGUGUAAAACAAGUUGUUUGGAAACUCUUAAAUCUUUUUGAAAACAUUACAGCGAAAUAACAAAAGUUUUCCAGAAGAGUCUGGUUAAGCAUUGAGCUAGAGCACAGCAUUUUCACAAGAGAAGUUUUAAGCAUGAUGUUACCCUAUCAAUAGUCGUGGCUGAAGAAGUUCUUUGAUUUUUGUUUGUUUGCAGAAUUCUGAUUUGUAGCAUUUGAUAAUCACAAAUUUAAAAAGGAUCUUUGCACUUGUGUUUUGAUUUUGGUCACAAUUUUAUAAAUUGGUAUGUUUCGAUGUUUUUGUUAGGAAAAAAAUGUAAUAUACUGACAUACCACCCCCCCCUUCCCCCCCCACACACUACACUUCUUUAAAUACGCCAGAUAAAAUCAUUUAAUCAAGCUUUUUGGGAAUGUUUGAGUGUGUCAGAGGUGACGUAUUGUGUAUAGACAAAGGUAAGAGAAAACCAGUCCAGGAAUGAGAACAUCAUUCCUGCACUGUAUGUGCAUGUGUGUUUUUCCUUUGCUCUAAUGGUAUUCCUCCCUUCCCCCAAAACCUCUGGUGUAUUUUCACUAAUAAUGAUGUCAGGUUAGGUACUUUUGGGAACAGUUGGAAAGGAAAACAGCAAGGGAGAAGAGGAUUGGAUCUUCGGGCUAUGAUUGGGAGGGAAGGCAGUCUAGGGAACUGGUUUCUGUGGGUAGCUCAUGAGGGAGAGCUUUGCAGUAGAAGAGGAGUCAAACCUUUUGGGAGGGUCAGGGGAAUAAAUUGGACAUUUCAGGGAGUCCCUGGAAUUGAAAGAAGCAGUCAAAGCAUUAAGGGAAGUCUUUUUGACACUACUCAAAGGAAGCCAGUGAGGGAAAGCAAUGAGCUCCUUUGAGAAAAUUCUGGGAUAGGAGCAUGGGGGCCUGGGAGGGGAGGGAAUCUCUGGAGUACCUUUGUUGUUGGCUCCACAUAGGUCCCUGGUGUGUGAAAGGAUCUAGAUAGGUGUAGUUAUAAAUGGGUUGGCCCUGUAAAUCUGUUCAUAUAUGUGAAUGUCUUUCUGAUUUCCUCUUCUUUUUACAUUCUUAUCUGAGUAUGGGAAUGGCUGAAGGCUUUAUUGCUAUCUGUGUGUUGCAUGCUAUGUGGAUCUUUUAAGGCGUGACCUUAUCAAAGUUGGCAUCUAAAUGCAAAAGAAAAUGCAGGGCAAGCUUGUUCUAGUUGGGGUUCCUGUCACCAGACCAUAGCAAUUUGGAACAAUGGAUACAUUACCUGAAUUCACUGGCAGCAAGCAGAGUCCCUGCUUCUAUGCGUGCCCUUAUCAGUGUUUAAAAUAGUGCCUCGUACUCUGCGUACUAUCUAGAAGAGAACACCUCCUUCCCAUUCUCUUCCUUUCCCUAUUCUUUAUUAAUAUUUUGGGGGGAAUGCUUUCAUUUCAAUAGUUAGAAAAUGUGGAAAAACAAGAUUGCAAGGUUGAGGUGAAAGUAGUACAAGAUUGGAAGAAUGAAACUCUUUUUUCUUCACUCAGUAAAAUGAUACUUUUGGCUCAGUGCCUGGGGAACAUAGGCGAGUUAGGAUGGUGCAGACAGGACUAGCAACAAGUUUGUUAAGGAAUGGGCUGAGAACCCCUUGCCUCUGCCCUGUGGUUUACUACAGAAUUUGAGUUGUAACUUUUUCUUUUUCUUUUUUUUUUUUUUUGUCCGUUAGAAGCAGUGGUAGAGAGAUUACACACUAAGCUUUAAAACCACAGCAAAACAAAACUUUUAAAACACUUGUGCGGUAACCUCAGAAGACAGGUUAACACAUUCUGUUUUAACUGUACUAUUAAUGUGUUUUGCAAGUUUGCAAUACCUCUAGACAUGGAGGUCUUUUUCCCCCUUACAUUUUAUGUAUACUGCAAAUCGAAUCCGAGGUGUGUCUUGUGAGCAUUAAAAUAAUGAAAACAAAACACAGUUUUAUCCAGGAAAUAUAUAAUUCUGAAUACUAAAAAUCUUUUUAAUUGAUCAUUUAUGUAAUAUAUCAUCACUUUUAUUCAAUACAUUUCAAAAUAUACUACUCUUUUUAGCAAAUUCAAAGUCCUUUUAACAUUUUCUUAUAAAUCUGAUAUCACUAUAUUUGUAACUAAGGAAUUUUAUGGUGAGAUUAUUUGAGCUUUAUUUCUGUAACAGUUGUUCUAAGUUAUAAAAAUGAACAUCUUUAACACAUCUAUAUAGACUUUAAAAUAGCUUAUUUGUAAUUUAAACUAUCUUCAAAUAUUUUGCUAUAUUCCUGUUUCCCCUAAUUAUUCAAAGUUUACAAAACAAACAUUUAUUGACGAUCAGUGAUGUCACAGUUUUAUUGUAAGAAGACAUUUCCUUUCAGAGAAUUAACGUAGAAAUAAGGAAGGUUAAAGAGAUUUCCUAUCCUUUCCUUAAAGAAAAAAAGGCUAUUUAUCACUUGCCAUCUUAUACUCAUUCAUUCAUUCUCUCAUUCACUAUACAUUCAGUAAGUGCCCACUAAACUUUUAUUAAGCCUUUCUUUUCGUUCAGUCUGUUGAUUUGAUAAAUCAGAAGAUUAUCUUUGAUAAGUAUUCAUAUAAUACUUUUUAUUAUCCUUUUGUGAUUGUUUAUUAAGCUAUCUGUCCAAGCUUUGAAGACAGUCUGCAAUGGUUCAAAUCUAAGCAUUGCCAUUAGUUGUGAUAUGUGUGUAUACAUGUCUGUUGGUCUCUCUAUCAUCAUUUAUCACAAUUUAUCAUUGUUUACCCAAAGGAAUAACUAGCUACUGACUGAGUGACCUUGUAUGAAUAAAUUAAUAUCUCUGAGCCUCAGUUGACUUACCUGUACAAAGUGAGAAUACUUAUAUUUUUUAAGAUUGUUAGAUUAGUUGUAUAUUUAAGCCCCCUCUACGGUAUUUAGAACAUGUGAGUAACGUGGUUACUUAUUAUUGUUUAUAUUGCCAUUAUCCUGACCACUAUAUGGACUUGAUCCUCCAGUUAUUUCCUUGGGUCCAUGCCAUCUUACCUCUCUUAUUUUUCCAUUACUGCUUAUCUCACAAUAUUCGAGAGUAAAAAGGAACCUUUUUACAAUGAAAGGCUGCCCAUUUCUCACAUGUGCUUUCCUCUUGAUGCCUUCAUGCUUGCUGUUUUGCUUACUGUUGUAGAGCAGCAGAAUAUUACUGAGGAAGCACUUCUUUUUAAAAAAAUUUUCUGGUACAGCUGGAAAUAUGACAAGAAGAAUAGAACAAUUGAUUAUUAGUUAAAUCAACAUAUUAUUCUAUAAAUUCAAUAGAAUUGAGACCCCCCCCCUUCCUUUAAAUGUUAUAUUUGGUCUUAUUAAAAUUCAUUUUGCUAUAUGCUGUGGAUUUUUAUGCAUUAUUUUUGUUUAAUUUCUAAUGAAGAGUUAUUGAGAUUUUAUGAGAUUGACGUCUUAUUUACUUAAAAAAUUUCCUAUUGCUUGUACAUUGGGAGCAAACCAAGAACAGGUGUAAAAACAACCUCCCAACUUGUCUUGGUGAAUUGUGAAUUGCUCUGGUUUAUUCUUGUUUGUAUUACAUUUAAUGGACAAGUCCUGUAUGGUACUAUACAUUUUAAUUCAGUUUUGAAAAUUAUCAAUUUGCAAAUUUUGUCUUUUUCCACUUUCUUUUUCUAUUUCAAGAGCUUAUUACCUUUGCUCCAGCUGGAUAAAAGUUGGGCAAACAGAUACCCUGACAACUGCCAACAGCACCACGCCUUGGUUUUCCCGGGUACAGAAAGUAGUCAAUAUUUCUGGGACUAUGCAUCUGUCCCAUCUCAAAGAUGCCGCUCACAAAUUCUAGUUUAAAUACAGAAUUAUUGAAAACAUGAAAAUCACCACUUCUUUAAAAAUAUGUAUUGUAUGUGCUUCUUUCCUGGUUUUACCAAAACAAGUAAAAAAGAUCCAUGUAGCAGAUUUAGGUCUACAGCCUGCAAAUUGCUUCCUGUUUGCUUGCAUGGUGACAAUGUUCUAAGUGCCAGUUUUGAAUACUAGUAACCUGUCAUGGAUCAGUUAUCUGAAAUGGCAGGUUUAUUUGUUAUGGGAGGAAUGACAUUAUUUCCUGUCCUUUAGACAGAGCUAAAGUGAGAAUAAAGUAGUAAGAAAGAAUGUUUCUUUGCACUCUAGGUGUGAGUGUACUAUCGUUCGUGCUACUGAUUUGAUUGCCACAGCUACUAUCAUUAGCAUCUUGGACCAAACAUGGAACAAGCUGUACUAUAUUUCAUGUAUGAUGGAAUACAGAGACUGAUUAAAAAUACUCUUAAGGUGCUGGAUUAUUCAUUUGAUAGCUGAUUGUUAUAAGACGUUAGGGUCGUACUUUCCUUUGUGGACAUAAACAUUUUUAAUAAUUGCUUUUUAAAAUUAAAUUUAAUUUGGAGCCUAGGUAAGGAUUUCCUUCAUUUGAACUAAUUUUUUUUUUGUAAUCUCAGAAUUAUCUUAAUAGUAGGUAGUGUCAGUUGCCAGAAAAACAUCAAUGUGAAGGAAAUUUGUAUAUCAUAAUUCUUUCCUAGUGUUUUCUUUAGGCAGACUACAGUGAACGUAUCUAUUCUAAUUCUCAUUCCUUUUCUGGAUAACCAUAGGUAAAGGUACUUUUAAUUUGACCUCUGAAAGAAGAAAAAGUUUUUCCAGGUUGGAGAAAUAAUGAGUAAUGCUGGUUAGAGACUGCCUCUCAUCUUCUUCUCAAAUCUUAGUCACUACCUAUUCUAGUGUUUAAAUAACUAAUGAAAACAUUUUUAUGGUUUCUGAGAUUUUUUUUAAAGCAGGCUUGAAAGAUAUGAAGUAAUUUACUGAUAAACCAAAUUUUAACAUUAUAGACAUAAGAAUGUUGUCUGUCCAUCUCAUUUUGUUUCAUUGUAAUAUUUUUCCUCAUAGGUAUAGGGAAAAUAGGUGAUUUUGUUUAGUCAACAAAGGGUUGUCUCUUCUCUCUCUCUCUCUUUCUUUCUCUCUCUCUUUCUACCAUGGCAGCCCAAGUAGGGUUCAACCGUGUAGGUAGGAUCUGUAUUAUUAAUUUUCAUUAUGCCAAAACUGACAAAACAUUACGUUGAAAUCAUAAAGCACUAGAAAAGCAAAUACCUAGAAAGUAUUAUCUGUUCUGUAAGAAAAACAACAAGCUAAACAUUUUAAUAUAUUAUUGAGUUUGUUGGAUUUAUAAUAUUGGGACUUCUCUUUAUACAAGUACCUGGCCUUUAAAAAGAAAUACUACCUAGAGUAGCCACAGGUACUGUUAAUGUUGCCAAGUAUUCCUAAGUAUAUUGUAGUUAGAUUAGUGUGAGGAACUUCCUUAAAAAAUUUAAGUGUAAACCUGUAAGGUUACUCUUAUUGGUUGUUUUUCAUAGUUUAUUUAGUGACUAUUGCACGGUAAUGCUUUGUAUUAGAUCAACAUUAAGUUAGAAUUCAGUGGCUGUAUUAAAUAGCCUUUUAAGACAGUAUGUUAAAUACGUGGCUUUCACCAAGGGGCCCCUAUGGUAUUUUGGCAAUUUUACUAUUUUUUAAAAUUCAUACCUAGUUUGAAUUGAGAUUCAUGUAAGUGAAACACCAUUAAUAAGGAUUUUUAGUUUUAAAUUUUAGUUUGUUUUAUUAUAAAAUAGUCAAUAUCUAUCAUUCUUAAAAUCAAGUAUUCUUUAUAGUAGUCCUACUUAAUAUGCAGUCUGUAGGCUGGAAAGCAUUUGUUACCAGUCUGCCUUGAAAUUAAAUAUAGAAGUUGAGUAAAUGCUUAAAACUGUCACCAAAGUUUGAUAGAGUAAUAAAAAUAGGGGGCUUGUAUUUUGUUUUUGUCAAAUUUGACUUGAUUAUACAAAUGUGAUGAAUUAGAAAUUUAAAAAACCAAUUGGUCCUUCCCACAGAAGGAUAUUUCAUUUGAGAAAUAUCACUUUAGAUGACAUUAGAAGAGUUAUCCAUGUGCUUAGUGUCAGUUAGCUUAAAUGCCAUACAUUAAAAUAUAAACAUAUCAAAAACCCACUUAUAUUAGUAACUUAUGUGGAUAACCAUAUGAUUUUUAUAAAGUAAUCUCAAAUGAAAAUGAAAGCCAAUUCUUUAAUGAAUCUAAAGCAGUAGAGCCUUUACUCAUAUACCUAGUAAUAACUAUCAUUAAGUGCUUACAAUGUGCAAUAGGGUGUCUUUUAUCUUAUUUAAUCCUCUAAAAGCACAACGGGAUAGGUUCCUUAUUACCCUCAUUUUAGAGAUGCCGAGCUAAGGGUCAGAGAGGUUAAAAAUGUGCUGAUGGUCACUGAGCUAACUAAAAAAGCUAACAUUAAAACAUGCUUUUGUUCAUAAUAUGAUUACACAUCUUGUGCUUCACGUUUUUUCUUUUAAAUGAGGAGGUAAUAACAUGUACUGGGUAAAGAAUGUUGUUUUGUGCUUGUAGGUAAAGCUGUGUACCAUGCUGUAUAUGAGGAAUUAUUUAGAGCUAGAAGAGGAAAGCUCAAGCAUGCAAAUCUUCAGUGCUGAGUUGGUAUAGGGAGUAAGAUGAGGCUUCAUCACGUACGUUGCUCUUGAUCUCAGAGUCUGUUACUACAAAUUGUUGAUGAUCACAAAAAUUUAAGGACAUCAUGUUCAAGUUACACUUGAUACAGCUUAUAAGAAAGAAUCCCUUUUCAAAAAAAGCAGAUGAGAUGUGAUUUUUAAAUGGCAUCUCUCUACUCUUCAUAUGUACAUAGAUACUCAACUUUCAGGAAUCAUGUAUAUAAUAUUGGCAUCUUACAGUAAUAUUUACAAUAUUUGUUUCCUUCAAUCUCUUCAGUUAUCUUUAUAAAAGAAAGGAGGAUGGGGGGAGGAGGCUGACUUUUGUCAUGUAGCUUCCUCAACUAAAGCCUUCAGAUCUUCAUCAGUAUAUGAAUAAACUCAGUUUACUAGAUGCUUCCCUUCUGUAAAAUUCUGUAAAUCAACUAGCUAAUAUUUAAUUGAAUUUUUAUCUUGUUUUCUUCAUUUGGUCCAUUUGAUUGCUGAUCAUUGAUGUUCAUCUGCCUAAUAACCUUUGCACAGUGUUUAAGGAUUGAGGAUAAAAACUAUCAAGGGCAAGAUUAGAAGAGGUGACUGACUCCCUGAUUCUCUGCUGCCCUUGAAGGCACUGGAUAAUGGAGAAACAAGUGCCUGCAUGUGUUGGAUUUUGUUAGUUGGAUCUAGCUCCAGCAGAAUGACAACUGAGGUCACGUCAGCACCUUGGAAGGCCGGGAAGCUGGAACUGGAGCAGCUGAGCCAAUCCCCAGACAAACAGGUUUUAACCGGGACAGAGUGAGAGAAUGCUUUGCUUUGGAAACUGUCUGCCCAUCACCUAAGGCGGUGAUUCUAUUCCUAUAUAUUUUUUUUCCUGCUGUCUGUUCAUUUUUGUAUAGAAAAGAUUAGUUAUGAGGACUUCUUUCUCUUUAUAUAUGGCAAAAAGUAAUUGCAAAGUAGUUAUGUUAGACUUUGAGAUUUUUUUGUUUUCUUCAGAUUCAGAAGCAAAGAAAAUGUUACUUUUGAAAUUAAGAUGGUGUGAUGGAAGGACCAUUUAUGGCAUUAGUAAGGGUGAUCAUUUGUUGAUUACCAUCAUUUUGUGUAAGGUUGAAUGCCAAUUAAAUGUCAUGGGUGCCUCAAUAUGUUUAAAUAUCUUCAUAUUAUAUAAUGUACAUUCAAACCUCUUUUGAUUCCAGGAGGAGAUUUUCUUGUAAGUCCUAAAAUUGGAAACUUGGAUUCUAGUCUCAUUUUGCGAGUUGCUCUACUCUGUAAUUUAUUUCUUCUCAAUAUGUAGAAUGGUGGUUCUCAACUUUGGCUGCACAUUAGAAUCAUCUGGAUAUGUUUAAAAAAUACUGGUAUUUUUACCCCAUCCCAUACCAAUUUAAUAAAAAUAGGGGUAGGGCUCAGGCAUUGAUAAUGAUUUAUUAAUUUCCCCAGAUAAUUCUGAUGCACAGUGAAGGUCUAGAGCCAUGGAUAUAGAAUGAUAUCACUGACCUAACUUCUGUGACUUUUUUGAGAUUGAUUAAUUCAUGUUAACUGUUUUAAUCACUCUUGUAAAAAAAGCUUUCUCUAAUUUAUAGGGUCUUUUUCAAAAAUAUAGAAUUAGAAGUGUCCUUUGAUAUACUUCUGUUCCUUGCCAGAUUACAUUCAACCAUUAAUUUAAGCAAAUUCAGUAAAGCUAGAAAUGCAGAGUGAUGAAGAGUGUGACAGGAAACCCCUGAGCCGUGAAGAUGAGAUCAGGGGCCAUGAUGAGGGUAGCAGCCUAGAAGAACCCCUAAUUGAGAGCAGCGAGGUGGCUGACAACAGGAAAGUCCAGGAGCUUCAAGGCGAGGGAGGAAUCCGGCUUCCGAAUGGUAAACUGAAAUGUGACGUCUGUGGCAUGGUUUGCAUUGGGCCCAAUGUGCUUAUGGUACAUAAAAGGAGUCACACUGGUGAACGCCCCUUCCACUGUAACCAGUGUGGAGCUUCUUUUACUCAGAAGGGCAACCUUCUGAGACACAUAAAGUUACACUCUGGAGAGAAGCCGUUCAAAUGUCCUUUCUGUAGCUACGCCUGUAGAAGAAGGGACGCCCUCACAGGACACCUCAGGACCCAUUCUGUGGGUAAACCUCACAAGUGCAACUACUGUGGACGAAGCUACAAGCAGCGCAGUUCACUGGAGGAGCACAAGGAACGCUGCCACAACUAUCUCCAGAAUGUCAGCAUGGAGGCUGCUGGGCAGGUCAUGAGUCACCAUGUACCUCCUAUGGAAGAUUGUAAGGAACAAGAGCCUAUUAUGGACAACAAUAUUUCUCUGGUGCCUUUUGAGAGACCUGCUGUCAUAGAGAAGCUCACGGGGAAUAUGGGAAAACGUAAAAGCUCCACUCCACAAAAGUUUGUGGGGGAAAAGCUCAUGCGAUUCAGCUACCCAGAUAUUCACUUUGAUAUGAACUUAACAUAUGAGAAGGAGGCUGAGCUGAUGCAGUCUCAUAUGAUGGACCAAGCCAUCAACAAUGCAAUCACCUACCUUGGAGCUGAGGCCCUUCACCCUCUGAUGCAGCACCCGCCAAGCACAAUCGCUGAAGUGGCCCCAGUUAUAAGCUCAGCUUAUUCUCAGGUCUAUCAUCCAAAUAGGAUAGAAAGACCCAUUAGCAGGGAAACUGCUGAUAGUCAUGAAAACAACAUGGAUGGCCCCAUCUCUCUCAUCAGACCAAAGAGUCGACCCCAGGAAAGAGAGGCCUCUCCCAGCAAUAGCUGCCUGGAUUCCACUGACUCAGAAAGCAGCCAUGAUGACCACCAGUCCUACCAAGGACACCCUGCCUUAAAUCCCAAGAGGAAACAAAGCCCAGCUUACAUGAAGGAGGAUGUCAAAGCUUUGGAUACUACCAAGGCUCCUAAGGGCUCUCUGAAGGACAUCUACAAGGUCUUCAAUGGAGAAGGAGAACAGAUUAGGGCCUUCAAGUGUGAGCACUGCCGAGUCCUUUUCCUAGACCAUGUCAUGUACACCAUUCACAUGGGUUGCCAUGGCUACCGGGACCCACUGGAAUGCAACAUCUGUGGCUACAGAAGCCAGGACCGUUAUGAGUUUUCAUCACACAUUGUUCGAGGGGAGCACACAUUCCACUAGGCCUUUUCAUUCCAAAGGGGACCCCUAUGAAGUAAAGAACUGCACAUGAAGAAAUACUGCACUUACAAUCCCACCUUUCCUCAAAUGUUGACAUACCUUUUAUUUUUUUUAAUAUUAUUACUGUUGAUAAUUCUUAUUUUGUGGAGGCAGUGUCAUUUGCUCUGCCUAAUUACGAUAAGGAAGAAACAGAAGAGAGAAGGGGCGGGAAUAUUGUUUCUUUAUCACCUGGCUUGUUUAUUUUGUGGGAAUUUAAGAGCAGUCCAUUUCUACCAAGGCAUAUCAUGCUUUGAAAAAUCACUUGAUUCAUAAAGAUUCACCUAAGAGAUUCUGAUUUGCCACUGAUAUUCAGAAUUAUGAUGGAAGACAGGAAAGUUCAGAGUUUUCUGGGUAGGACUUUGGUGGUUUAAAAAUGGUAUAAGUAACUUUAUUCUUGAAAGAAGAAUGUGUUUCAAACUGUAAACCAAUUUUUUGUUCUUCAGAGAUCAUGGAACACAAACACAUUGUUAUUUUCAGUGAUAACUCCUAAGAGGAGCUGAGUUGUUGUGGGUUCUAUGUUUACUUCCCCUAUGGAAUUUAUAAUUCAGUAUGUUUUACACUGUACCAUAUAGCAAAACUUUUAAACUACAGGUAGUUAAGGGCCACCUACAAUACAUCUGAGGUCCUGUGAUCUUAUUUUUCUAAACGUAAGCACUGUUUUUCCAUAGUUUUGAUGACUGGCAUUUUAUAGACACCCUGGCAGCCUUACUUUUAACACCUUUAAGGAAUAGUAUUUUUAUGUAGUUUUCAGAAUAACAUAUGGUCUAAGAGUGGAUAAAAGGCAGUCAAUAAUUUCUGGGAGGGACUUCUACUUUCAUAAAUUUGUUUGAGAGGUUUUCUUUUAAAGUUGUAAUGUGAUGGCAGCAUAGUAUAUGUAUUUGUUUCUAAAAGUAUGCUUACGAUUGUCACUUUAUCAGCAUUUAAUCAGUGUUAACCAGUCAGCAGAAAAAUAUAAUUAUGCUAACAGUAGGGGGAGAAAACCCACUUAGAAAUCCCUUUUCUGGUAUUUCUCUUUUCACUAGUUUUUUUCAAGAUGUGACCUCCCGGUGUUCUGUCCAUAGUUCAUUCAUCCUUUACUCUUCGAGUAGAAGGUCUUAAAAGUCUUCCUGUCGGCUGUUUCUUUCAAAAUCUCCUCAGAGCAAUUGCUAAUUUGGCCUGAAUCUGGUAACUUGAACCCUGUAAGGUUACAGAACUAGGGCUAUUUAUUUUAGCAUUUCUUCAGUAGUAUUUACUACUCUUGUUGCAAAGAAAAGGGAAUGGGACUUCUUUGUAACCUGUACCUUGGACAACAGAUAAAAGAAACAAAAAAAUAAGAAAGUUUACUUUUACCCUUCUUGGAGUCUAGAAUGUGACAGAACCCCCAAAGGAAAGUCCUGCACAUUUUUCUGUUUCCAAAACAUUUAAUUGUGUAAGUCCUUGUCAGAAAUGAAUCUCAAUCCCUUAGUAUAGAAUUCCCCUUACAUGGUAUAGGUUGCCAUAUUUCAUGUGCAGAUUUUAAUUUCAUUUAUGUGGGCGCUCUGUUUUUUCUUUGCAGUCCAGCCACAUUAGAGGGGAGGAACCGAGUGAUAUUGAUUCAAGUCAUUUUAGGGGGACAUACUUGGAAGGCAGAACUUGCUGCUUCUGUUUGGGGAGGACAGACCUGACUGUGACUGGAUUAUCUGAUAACCAUUUGUGAAUACUGAAAUUCUGUUAGGCAGUAACUGAUAACUGCUCUAAAGGAUCAUUAAAUAGGAUGCUGAAAUUAUGUAUCUUAAUACAGUGUGGUAUGAGAAUUACCAAGUCAAGAGAAUUGUGGACAUAAGCAAGUUUGGCCCCAAUACUGCUCUUAACUCAUUUUCCAGCUUACUAUUUGCUAUUUAAAUGGUAGGCACCAGCUAAGCACUUCUAAGCACUAACACAGCUAGAACUAGGCAAAAAUGGUUAGAACUCAGCUCUCUUCUACUAGUCCCUGUCAUAAUUAUUUUUGGGAAAAUGUCCAAACUGCCCCCUUUAAAUCUAAGGGAAUGCACCAAAACAGAGAUAUAUAGAAUGUCAACCAUUUCAUUUUUUUUUUUCUGCAUGCCUUGGUACAUAGUGAACAUACAACCUAUUUAAAGAUAAAGCAUGUUUUUGAGACUCGCUCACCCCCCCCCACCCAACCACUCCCAAAUAAUAAUUGGGAUGCCAUUUUUUUUCCUUUUGGAUGAGGUAAAUAAUUUUAAGGUUCACAAUUUUGUCUUUUACUGCAAUUUAAGGAAACAUUUGGAUGUCAGUCAAUAUGUUCAUAAUUUUGGCUGUGUGCGAAUUUCUGCUGGCAUUAUCUAUGAAUUUUCUUCCUACUUAUUUUUUUUUCAGUAUAUGAACAAUCAUGUAUCUACCUGCCCCAGGAUGAAACUAAAUUUAGGUGGACCCUAAACCUUAUGAAGACAGUGCUGAGGCACUUUCCUUUUCUGAUUUCAUCUUUUUGGGAAUCUGUUUUAUUGAAGGUAGUUAGUAGUUGAGAGUGCAUUUGCUACAAGCAUAUACUUGUAUCUUCCUAGCUUCAUGAGGAACAGAAAGAGGUGGAUAUGGCUCAGGGUGUGGCAGGGACAAUUGAGGACAAAGUCAAUUCAAAUUUGUGGGUCAGAAAGAAUUUUUGUGGACGUAGUGUUUUUGGAGAAACUCUGGAUGGUUAUAUGUGCAUGCCUUUUCUUCAAAAGGAAAUACGCAAGGUUGUAGCAUCUAAAAAUAAACAUAAGAGUCAGACACCAAAUAAAUCAAGUUUUACAUAACAGUUGUAUGCCCAGUUUGUUUAGGUGAGAUUUCACAUUACAGAAAGUAUUUGAGGAGCAUGAAAAUGGGUUAUCUUCUGUAUUUUCCAGUUUGGCAAAAGUUCAGAAUUUCAUCACAUUGCUUUGCCCUAAUUUUGCCCAGAAUUUUAUCUUAGCCUCUCUCUGACAGUGAUGAAUCAUGCUCAAAAGCCAUUCUAAUUGGACCUUUUUAAGACAGGGAAAGGGAUCAGUAGGCGGAUUGGAAGAAAUUUCAAGUCAUUGAAAUAUUCCAUUGAGAUUUCCUAAAGGGACAAAAUUGGGAAAAUAAGAAACUACGACUUAGAUUUGGCUACGUAGUAGAAAGUAUCUCCCCUACAUACAUACAGGCAAUUGUAUGUAUGAAUCAUAGGGUAUAUGUGUGUGUAUACUACACACACAUUCUUUUAAAGAGAAUUCAUGGAAAAAAAAGCAGUUGGAGUGAUCAGAUGUAUUGCAAAAACAUACAGAGAAUUUAAAUGACAGUUAAUACCAAGAAAUUAGUUGGGUUUACUUUAUCAGGUCGUAAUAGGAAUCACUAAAGAAGUUACUAGUGUGUCUUUAGGACCAGUGGCAACUCUUAAACUAAAACUUUGGGUCCUUAUUAUCUACUUACAGAACAAAGUGAAACAAACAAUGAUUAAGCUGAUUGGAUAUACAUUCAAAGAUAUUUAAUGUAAAGUUUUUUGGAAUACGAAGAAAAUUCAGAAAAUAAAUAUUAUCAACAGUUACUUAUUGGCAAAUAGAGAAAGACAAGAAUAGUUUAGUGAGCCCGGUAUUUUGUUUUUAUAGUUUUUAUCUCAGUUGUACAACUCACAAAACCAUGAAGUCUUUGGUAUUUUAUAAAUGUUUAACAAAAUUUACAUCAGAUUAAGGCAUUUAGAUGAAAAUUAUUAUGUUCUCACUAUCUUCCAAAUUUUAUUUCAUCCUAUCUCCAAAAUGAUUUCUUAGGGUACAAAAAGAGCAGACGGGGCUGUAAAAAUACAAGCAAAAAACUGUGUGCCCCUAGUUUCAGGCAGAACUUAAACUGUCAGAGGUACUAGCUACAUGAUUUGUUUUUUAACUUUGGAUUGUUCACGUCCAAAAAUGGAUAAAUUACAUUUGUGUUUAUCAUCAGUUGCAUUUUAUGUAUUAUUUUAAUAAAUACUAUCUGAAUGAAGACUAUUCUAAACCAGAAAAUUCCCCAAAUCCAAAAGAAAAAAAAAGUGGGAAGAGGUGAAAUUGAAGUUUGUGUAUAUGAAAGUUAUCUUAGACAUAUUUUUAAUUCUCCAGUUUCUGCAAAAUAAUUAAAAUAUACAGUAACUGGUCUCCUAAAUCCUGAAUUUAAUGUAUUAAAUACUUAUGUUCUUUAUAUUGGUGCCUUUUUAAAAUGCAUUGAGAGUGUUGGUUAGCUGUUGCAGCUGUACAACACUUUUAAUAUGCAUUUUUAAAAAUCACUUAAAAUUGAGUACUAUAUAAUUCAUCUCUGCAUUUUUAGUGCAAAUCUUUAGAGCAAUUUCUAAUAGAGAAAUUUUCAGCUCAGCUGUUAAAAGGAAAAGGAAACUUUGAAACUAGACUUUACUACCUUUUUAGUUUCAUAGUAUUUCUGAAUAUGAUUACAAGAUUAUGCAGGUAAAAUAUAGAGUGAAACUUUACCUGUGAAUUGAAUUAUAAUUUGUGUUUUUGUUUUGUUUUUAAGGAAGAAUAAGUUCUGUAUCAAACAAGAAUUUAUUAGAUAAUUUUUUGGUCAAUAAAAUACAGUAUUCAUUUGGAUUUUCAUCUCCAGACUAGUAUUGUUCUAGUCUUGGAAUCUGUAUUUUCUAAUCUGUUAGAAAAUAGAGAUUGAAAAUUGAUGGAAUAAUGUGAAAAAGCAGGUAAUUAAUUCUCCUUGAACAAAGCAAAACUGAACAGUCAUAUCACAUUGCUAUUCUCCAAAGCAUAAUCUCAAAUGGUUUCAUAUCAUGGUUGUGUAUUACUUGCAAUGGGUGUGUUAGGAUAUGACAGCUUUUUAAAAAAAUGAGCUGCUGGUUAUACAAAGCAAAUGGCAUAUGACCAAGAAGCUGUGAUAUGCUAGUGUUUCUUUUUAUCAUAGUGUAUUACUAGGCCAAAUAAUGACACCUUGAAUAUUUUUACAUUUAUUGCAGAAACCUUAAACUUUGGAAUUUCCAUAAGGUUUUUAUGUAAUAUUCUAUUUCUAGCUUUUUAGUUUUAUCUUGCUGUACUGUAAGUUUGAGGAUAUUUUUCACCUGCACUCUUAGGAAUAAGUUCAUAAUUCUGUUUAUGGGGCUUUCCUCCCAUAACACUGCAUUUGUAUAUUUUCUGUAUAAAAUAUGUGUUGUGUAUUAACCUUUAUCCCAUACAGAGAGUGGUACAUGAAUGACUAGUUUUCUAAGAUGUCCUUUUUAUUGUGAAUAAAAUAUAAAAGUUAAAGGCCCUCUGCUAAGUCACAUAAAGUACAGCAUAUAAGUUCAUAUAGGUACAAAUAAAUGAGUUUGCAGUGAAUUGGGCCUUCAAAUUACCUCAAGUGACAGAUAGUAAGAAAAGCUUCUUGAGCAGGUGGAGGUCACUGAAUCCCCUACUAUGCACUUACCAAGAUUUUACUUACUUUAAUUUACUGGAAAUUGAUUUUUUAAAAAAUGACUACACUGUAACAAGGGAAGGGAUCUGGGUUUUUUUGUUGUUUUAUUCUUGUUUUUUUUAAGUAGUUCAAAUUCUGAAACUGUGAUUUAAAAAUUUUUUACAGUCAAGCAUUCUGAUUUUGAACAUAACUCCCUUCCCUUUCUGUGUAACAAAGGUCUCUCUGUUAUCUCUUAAAUUUUGUUACAUCUCCCUCAGCCUCUUUCUUUGUCCGUCUCCCUUCUGUCAUUGUCUAUGGAUGUUUACCUCUCUGUUCUCCUAAAAGUUUGAAGAUUAGGUCAACUCUUAUUUCUAGUUCAUUGGUAAUUUAAUCUUAAUUUUUUUUUCGUGAUUUUUGUUGGUUGUAUAAUCUGCUGACGUAUUUUUAUACUCAAGUGUAGUUUUCUAUUAAAAAGAAAAGUGGUUGGAUUAAAAAUAGUAAGCUAUGUAACCCUCAUGUUACUUUCACUUUCAAAUAUUGGGUACCUAAAACAUUACUUCAGAGAUUAUGUAAUCCUAUUAUAGUAUGUUUGCUUUCCUUUAUUGUUGGAUUUUACAUUCUGAUUUGGCUUUCCUCCAAAAAAUGUAUAUCAUGAAAGACUAGACAGUUAUUUGCAAGUGUUUAGAAAGGUGUUAAAAAUGUAAAGCAAAGAGUCUUAACUUUCUCCUAAUUGGGAGAAAAAUGCUUUAACAUUACUAUAAUAAUAUUCCAGGUUUGGAGGGGGUCUCCAGGCCCCAUAUUUGCUGUUAAUAGUUGGACCUUUUAGACCAUGUGUUAUUUGCAAUCCCAGAAUGAUUGCUUCUGCUAUUAGUUAAAAAGAUACUAUUCUUUUCUUUCUGUACAAGUGCAAUACUCCCCUUGAAGUCUUAAAAACUAUGGUGAUUUUUUUUUCUUUUCUGACCUAUUCUUCCUUUAGCUAAUGACAAAAAGAAACUCAUAAAAGUCAUAGUAUGUUAAAGGACACAACAAGCAAAGAGAAAAACACUCCACAAUCAAAAGAUUACAGAAUGUGGAAACCACUAGUCUGAUCUCAUGGUAUCUUUAUUUAAGCUAAAUUUCCAUGGAAAUUAGUAAUCUUUUGCUUGAAAAAUGUGUCCUAAAGUUGAACUUUUUACAGAUUGAAUCUUCUUAGACCCUCGCCCAAUGCUCUAAAUUAAGAACCUAAUACUUAAUAUUUUUAUUUUACUUCUCCCCUUUUAGAAAUAAACUUUUAAAUAAAAGCAAAGCACUUAGCUGAGUUUUAAACACUUACAUAUCACCUAUUGGAGAAAUUUUUUUUAAAAAUAUUUGGAGCAGUCCUGUUUUCAUACAAAUUUAAGUAAGAGGUAUUUUUCUUAUACAUAUUUAUAUGUAGUGUGCUAAUUUUCUUUUUUUAUACCUGUGUCCCUGUAGUAAAACUGCUGUAAUAUAAAUACAUGUUUUGUUAAAAGAUAACAUUUCUUUGGCAUUUCUUUUAAAGGCAGUUACUGCAUUUCUGCAUUUGUACAGUAUGUGUCUUGGCCAUUUUAGAUAUUCUUUCUUUAACAAUACCAAAGGUAAUUAGACUAUUUUAAAGACUAAUUGCUUGACAGUUUCUAGGGUAUUUUGUGUUUUAGAAGCAAAAAAAGAAAAAAAAAUAGGUCAAACCAGUAAACCUCAUUUUUUUUCAAACUAAUAAUUUGGGGAAAUAAAAACUAUUGUUUAAAAAAGAAAUAUAUAUAUAUAUAUAUAAAUAUAUAUGUAAAGUUAAAAUUCCAUACCUUGUAUGUCAGGUUUGCUAAGUGUAAUGUAGUUUUUUUAAGGCUCAAAUACCAUACCUCAGAAAAUGAGGUUUACUAUGGAAAUACUGAAACAGUCUUUGCAGCUGUGUGACAAGUCACUCUACUACAUACUGAUUUGGAGACCUCCGCUAAAUAGUUUUAUCACUGCAGACUAAAAUGUGGGACUUGUAUCUUCUUUGUUUUUAAUGCACACACAUACAUGUUCUGUGCAUGUAUGUGGUUACUGUGUAUAUGUGUAUGAGUGUUGUAUAUGCAUGUGUGAGUGUGUGUCUGUAUGUGUGUACAACUAAAGAAGCUGCAGAAACUUUGUAAUACUUUGUGAAAAGGAUUAUAUUAUAAAGGUUUGUACUGUCUGAGUGCACAGCUACUGGAAUAAAUUUAGGGAAUCUCAGGAACAAGCAUAUAAUUUGUCCAAGAUUUAUUUCUUCUCAGAAGUGUAAGUGCAGUUUUUAAUUCUGUAUAUUAUUUAAUAUUUUACCAAUAAAAUAAACUUCUGACAUAAAAA